CUCUCUGGAGUGAGGCGAGAGCCCCGCACAGAGCGAGGGAGACAGCGAGCUGAGCUCCGGGCGCUGCCGCUGCCGCUGCCGCCGCCGCCGCCGCUGAGACUGAGAGCGAAGGAGCAUCCGAGAGAUCCAGUCCCCCUGCACUGGCCGCCGCCGAGACCUUCGCUCUCACCUGGGCCAGCGGGAGCCGCGGCCGCACUCCUUUCCCCCCCUCACCUUCCCGGCCGGCAGCGGCGGCUGCACACGCCGGAGCCGGAGCCAGAGCCGGAGCCCGAGCCUGAGCCGGAGCCGGCGGCUUGGGGGGCAGGGAGGCGGCUACCACGGGCCGGGAGUGGGUAGCUGCUCCGCGGUGAGAGAACGCUGAGGAGGCGCCAGAGCUUCUGCCUCGUCCCGUGGGGCGUGGGGCGAGACCCCCAAGGUGUAGGGAGGGGGGUCCCAGCCGCAGCGACACAUGCGGGAGCCGGGAGCGGGGGCGGCGCCGAGCGGAGCCGGCCGGGUCCCUCGCCUUGCCGCCGACUCGGCCACCCGCCCGGGGCCGUAGCAUCUUGCCCCGGAGUGUAUGAACCGGGGCCCCAACCAAGCUCGGCAACCACCCCCCGGCCGGGGGGGCGGGGACCCCGAUGUGAAGCGGCGGCUGGGGCGGCGGAGAGAACAGGACCGACGCCGCCGUCCUUUCCUCACCUUCCCCCUCCCCUCAGCCCCCUCCGGGGGUCUUCUCCCUUGGCCAGUCGCCGGCCCCCCGGCUCCUUGGCUGGACUCCGGGAGGAGUUCCUAGAGCCCCCCUCCCCCGCCCCAGUCCCGAGGGCGGCGGGGCCGGGGGGGACCCGGGGGGCCGGCCGCAGCCUCCACCCAGAGGAAACUUUACAAAAACAAAAUCCGGAGUCUCCCAAACCUGACUGUCCCGGGAGAAGUGGCCCUGGACGGGCAGAAGCCGCAGCCUGAAAAGACCCAGGAAGAGGAAAAGAGGAGUACCGCGCCGGAGCCUUCCGCAGCUGCCGCUUCAGUCCGAAGGAGGAAGGGAACCAACCCACUUUCUCGGCGCCGCGGCUCUUUUCUAAAAGUUGUGAAAGCAGCUGUAGACAACAAGGAAGUGAAUGAAUGUUGCCGUGCUCCAAUUGGCCCAUAGGCCGAAGUUUUUGGACUCCUGGUAUAGACAACUGCCAAAUCCACCAACAAACAGUAUGAGCUUUAUUACACUACAAAGCCAGGACUGGCUAUUUUUGGUGGUCUUUGUUUUCUAGAUGAGAUGUUUUUCUCUGAGUUCAUUUAAAAUGAUUCUGCAUAAAGCACAUACUCUACUGUACAAAAUACUUUUGCCUUCAUGGUGAUGAAAACUAUGGAUUGAGGGUCGGGGUGAUACCAUCUUUAAAGGGAUGCAGCUAAAAAGUAGGGACUACCUGCAUUUCUUAUCUAAAGAUAACCACAGUUGGCAUUUAGUGAUAUACUGGCUUUGUAUCAUGGCCAAAAGUAUCUGUAAAGAAGCUUGUGGGCAUACUUUUGAAACCUUCUGAAAAUAAAUGUAAAGCAUUUACUUCGUGUGUAAAAUUAGAAGUGUCUAUGGUUGGUUUGAAUAAUAUGAGUCAAAUUAUAAGAGCAUUAAAGUUUGAUACUGCUAUCUAUUAAAGUCUUAAUCUCUUGCAGUGGCUAAUUCAGUGUGUAGAAUUACACAUCGCAAUUUUUGUUUUGUUAAUUUCAAGUACUAGUGUAUAUUAACAAAUCACUUAAAUCAUUUAAAUGUGUACUUUAAAAAGCUUUGAUGUAUAUACAUAUAUAUACGUAUAUAUAUAUAUGUACACGUAUAUAUAUACACGUGUGUGUGUGUGUGUGUGUGUGUGUGUGUGUAUUUUUUUUUUUUUUGUGACGGGGUCUCAUUCUGUCACCCAGGCUGGAGUGCUGUGGUGUGAUCUCAGCUCACUGCAACCUCCACCUCCUGGGCUCAAGUCAUCCUCCUACCUCAGCCUCUCGAGUGGCUGGGAUCACAGGCAUGCGCCACCAUGCCCGACUAAUUUUUUUGUAUUUUUGAUAGAGAUGGGUAACAACUUUUGGAUUGAUAGGGAAUUAGAGAGCCUCGAGGGUAUAUGUGUGUGUGUUUUAGCACCCACCAGGUAACCCCAAAGGCCAUGCAUCAUGUUGCCCAGGCUGGUCUCUUAACUCCUGAGCUCAGGUAAUCCAUCUACCUCGACCUCCCUCAGUGCUGGGAUUGCAGGCGUGAGCCACCACACCUGGCCAGCAUUGCUAUAUUUUUAAGAGUGAAUCUUUCUCACAUGUGUUGUUCAGAAAGUGUAAUUCACUUUGUGCAAUUUUACAUUACAGUUAAUAUUAAAAUAUUUGUUUCAUAUGUCAGCAGAUACCAACAUUGGAUGAUGGUAUAUUUAGUUUCAUAAAUCCUAUUUAUUUUAGGAUUCCCUUGUUUAUGGCAGGGGUGGAGAUUACUCUUGCAAUAAUGAUCACUUUUUAGUUAGUUUGAAACCUGCUUUUAGUUUAUAUGUAGUAUUUCUACAUAUUGUUACUUAAAUUGAACUAACAAUUUACUUUUUAAUUUUUCUUCUUCCUUUUAAAAAAAGAGUAUAUAAUCUGACAAUGUUAGUACAUCUUUUAGAAGGUCACUAUAAAGUUGCUUUCCCUAUUUAUUUGGAAAGGAUUAUUUCCUUAUUAUUUUAAAAAAUCUUUUAAUUUUUGUCUUUUCAAGUAAUUUUAUCAUUGUCCCAAGCCUAAGGAUGAGUGGCAAUUUAAAAGACACAAGGUGUGCAUCUUCUAUCUGCAAAUACUCCAAACAGAAAUUAUUCCAGUUUGUUGAUACUUUGAGUGGACCAGGGAAAAAUGUGUAUGUUUUUAGUGUAACUGAAUUGUCAUUACAAAAAGAUGAGUAAAGUUGCUGUUAAAUAAUGAAUUCUUGCUGUUAAUUUGUCCUGUUCUUAGACUUUCCCCCAUUAAGUAUAAUGGGGGAAAAUGUACACACACACACACACACACAAAGUAUGUAUGUGUAGAUAUACCUAGCGUAUUGUGCUAGAUGUUCAUUUCUGCAUGACUGCUCUGGAAUUUAGGCAAUAUUAAAAGACCUUACAAAAUAUUUUUAAUAUCACUUAAUAUCCUGUUUUAUGUCUUAAUGUACUUUUAUGUUUUUGCUGCUUUCUGAUGAUACCUCCUUGGUACUUCCUCAUGAUACCUUUCACAGUAUGUUUAAAUGGAAUGUAUUUUCUCAAAGUACGUGACAUUUUCUGAACACUAUGGGAUAUAUAUCUUCUAGUAAUUAUAUUUUUACAUGCAAGUAUCUUUAAAAAUUUCUUCCUAUUACAACUUAAGAAUUGUGAAACAUUUGAGGGAGCAUCUGCAGUUUGAGCACUUGAUCUGGAUAUUGGAAUGACAAACUUAACAUUUAACUAAAUUUUUCUGAGGUGUUCUUUUACAAUUUUUGAGUUAACACUUGAUUUCUGUAAAGCAGAAGGCUUAUAAGAAGAAAAUAUGAGAGCCAGUGUUCGUCUUGUAUUAUCCUGCCAUGCACGUAGUUGAAAAUCAGAAACAAACAGAAAUGCACAAGAGACCUUAUUGCUUGAGUAUCUUCUGCUCUUCCCCCAUCAGACCUAAGGGACAGCUAGUGGAUCAGUCAGAUACUGUGCAGUUUCUGUUGCUAUGCUGUGUCACCUUUGCCCUUUCUUUCUAUCUGGAAGAUAGCUACUGGAAAUCUGGCUGUAAGAAAGAGAUAGCAUGUUUUUUUCCUCUCUCUCUCUGUGUGUUUCUGUCUGUCUGUGUACCUGUACCUAGUGUAUUGUGUUAGAUGUUCAUUUCUGCAUGACUGCUCUGGAAUUUAGGAAAUAUUAAAAGACUACAAAAUAUUUUUAAUAUUAUUUAGCCUUUUCUCUGAGAGGAUCACAUCCUCUGGCUUUGGCGUUUUCAUCUCACAGCAUCUUAAACGAACCCGUCAAUGUUUAUUAUCAGUUCCAAAUGUGAAGUCUCAAGGCAAAUUGUUGGUUUGUUUUUGGAAGAAUGUAUGUGUGUGUGUAUAUAUAUGUGUGUGUGUGUGUGUGUGUGUGUGUGUGUGUGUGUAUAUAAUUUUUAAAUUUUUAACAAAAAUUCCUGAUCUAGUCAAUGCUUAUGAGAGUGUGUGUGGUUUGUAUAAAAUUAUUUUUUUUAGAGACAGGGUUGCUUGUUGUCACCAGGCUGGAGGGCAGUGGUGUGAUCCUUGCUCACUGCAGCCGUGACCCCCUGGGCUCAAGUGAUCUUCCCACCUUAGCCUCCUGAGUAGCUGAGUAGCUGGGACUAUAGGUGUGUACUGCCACACCCUGCAAAUUUAAAAAAAAAAUUCUGUAAAGACAGGGUCUCACUAUAUUGCCCAGGCUGGUUCUCAAACUCCAGGACUCAAGCAGUCCUCCUGAAAUGGCCUCCCAAAGUGUUGAGAUUACAGGCUGGGGCCACAGUGCCCGGUCAGAGUGUGUGUAUUUUUUAACAGCCUUUUAGGAUUGCAUGCUUUUUAGGGGGGUGAAUGAGGGGUAAUAUACCUUUGCAUGACAUUCUCUAGGUCUGAGAAGGAGUUGCUUCACUAAAAGUGUAAUUUAUAAUUACCAAAUGGUUGAAAACAGGUCUACCUGGAGUCAGCAACAGGCAGCUAGUUUACUUCUCAUUUACGUAAUAAAAUACAUUCAUAAUAUGCAUUCAGUAAUUCAUAAUUCAAUAAUUUCUUGGCUUCAUGGCCUUGGACAAGCUAUUUAUUAUCCUUUUAAUUUUGGUGGCAUCACCUGUUGAUGGAGGAAAACGUGUCCUUUACAUGGUGGUUGUUAGGAUUAAAUGAGAUAAUAUAAAGCAUGCAAAGCUCUUAAUCCAGUGCCUGGCAUAUAGCAUUUGACCCAUCAGUGUUAAUUUAUUAAGUUAAAGUUGUUUUAAAGUGUGUUGUAGAUAGAAGAUUUAAAUCAGGCCUUAUAUUAAGCCCAACAUUUAAAUUCAACACUUGAGUUUGACAAAUAAUACUGAAGUAAUUCUGUGUUUUCAGAAACAUCUAAAACUUCAUUAACAUUUUAUUAAAAACUGAAGAAAUGACAGAACUGUUGGGCUUUUUUUUAAUAGAAAAGAAAGACUGAUUUGAACAUAACUGGAAUUUGAAUUUAGUUUCAAAGAUCUCAGUAGUGCAUGGACCAGAAAAGAAUCCGUUUUUGAAUAGUUAGUGAUUAUGAUAGUGACUGUGGUUUAAAUUGCCCAUUUAGAAAUAGCAGGAUCUAAUUCAGUUAUCAGCCUUUUUAGUUGCCCAUCUCUUUAACCCCUGGAAAUAAAAAGCUUUAAAAAAUCAUUAAGAAGUUGAACGGAAAUUUUAUCUGUGUCAUUUACAUCUCAAAUUAAGAUCGAAAUAAUUUUGUUUACAUGAUUCUAUUUUAACUACUUAAUUUUAGUUUUUGUUUUUUCCUGAAAUUAUUAGUAUGUGGGUUUUAAAAAUUCCUUUUUUUGUGUGCUUAAUAUUUGUUAAAUACAAGAUUGGUUUUCAGAAAUACCUUUUCUUCGAGUAGGGCAUAAUCAGUGUUUUAUUGGCCAAUACAAUAAAUAAAUGCUUCUUGAUUGUUUUUGUAUUUGGAAAGAAAUUCUAUGUUGAGAACAGUUUUGGUAUGCUUUCCUUCAUUGGCUGUUUAUUGAAUAGAACUGUAUAUUUAAGGUAUAUGAAAAAAAUCUAAGCUAGAAAAAAAGACUGAGAUACAUUCUUGGAAGAAAAUACUUGCAAACUAUGCAUCUGACAAAGGUCUAUUGUCCAACGUCUAUAAGAACUUAAAUUUACAAGAGAAAAACGACCCCAUUAAAAAGUGGACAAAGGACGUGAAUAGACACUUCUCAGAAGAAGACUUACAUGUGGCCAACAAGCAAAGAAAGCUCAAUAUUACUCAUUAGAGAAACGCAAAUCAAAACCACAAUGAGAUACCAUCUCAGACUAUUCAGAGUGGCUACUAUAAAAAGUCAAAAAAUAACAGAUGCUAGUGAAGUUGUGGAGAAAAGGGAACACUUAUAUACUGUUGGUGGGAGUGUAAAUUAGUUCAACCAUUGUGGAAAUCAGUAUCGCGAUUCCUUAAAGAGCUAACAGCAGAACUACCAUUCCACCCAGCAAUCCCAUUACUAAUGGGUAUAUACCCAGAAGAAUAUAAUUCAUUCUACCAUAAAGACACAUGCACACGCGUGUUCCUUACAGCACUAAUCACAAUAGCAAAGAUGUGGAAUCAAUCUAAAUGCCCAUCAGUGACAGAUUGGAUAAAGAAAAUGUGGUACAUACACACCAUGGGAUACUGUGCAGCCAUAAAAAAGAAGGAGAUCAUGUCUUUUGUGGGAGUAUGGAUGAAGCUGGAGGCUAUUAUCCGUAGCACACUAAUGCAGGAACAGAAAACCAAGUACCGCGUGUUCUCACUUAUAAGUGGGAGCUAAAUGGUAAGAACUUAUGAACAAAAUGAAUAGACACUGGGGUCUACUUGAGGGGGAGGGUUGGAGGAGGGAGAAGAGCAGAAAAGAUAACUAUUGGGUACUGGGUUUAAUACCUGGUUGUUGAAAUAAUAAGUACAGCACACCCUCGUGACAUGUGUUUACCUAUGAAACCUUUACAUGUACCCCGAAACCUAAAAUAAAAGUUUAAAAAAUAUAUUCUUUAGCACUGAUUAUCUUGCUAGCUGUGACUUCUCCUUUUAAGGAAAGUUUGCUUUAGAUUUUGGUGUAAAUGUAGAAAUUAGAUGGGUUUAUCUGCUAGUGGCUCUCUAGUUAGAUGAUUAAUGAAUAUUCUAGUUUAAAAAAUUUCAGCAUUUUAAAUACUUUUCUUUAUUGGUAACGAUUUGGAUUAUGCUUCUAGGGAUCUUUACAUUUCAUAGUUUUUCAAAAAAGACUUUAUAAUGAGUUCCUGGAUGGGAAGAAGAGCAUGUUCUCUCUAGUUUAUUUGAUUUCUUCCUGAUUAUUAUGUAUGUAAUACUGGAAGGUUGUGUAAAUAAAUAUUUGGGUUGUAAGUUUUCUUUUGCAUGAUUGGUGGUCUCUUAAUUGACUGCUGUGUGAAUUUGAUAGUAUAAACUAGAAUGCUUAUACAGUGAGUGGGGAAGCCUUUUUCUACUGAGUGUUAUGCAGGUGGAUUUUUCCCCCCUGCGGAUAAAUACUAAACUUUUAUAUUACCAGAUUUAGACAUUUAGACAGGAAACAAAAUUUCCUUUUUUUUAAAAUAAAUGAGCGGGAGAAGAGAGUGGGGUUGUACAGAGGUGGGGAGAGAGGCAGUAAAGGAGGGAGGAAAGAAGAGGCAGAUAUCAGGGAGAGUGGCUCCGGAAGUUUUGAGUUCAGUCUUAGUCAGAGGUCACACCCUGUUAUUUCUUUGGGUUGUGGACAUGAGGUGUUACCACUUGUUAUCUGUCACCCUUUGAAAUGAUGAUUAGAUUAUUGGUUUUUAUUCAUAGCUUUUCAACAUUUGGGUUCUUUAAACCAUUGAAGGUUUAGUUUGUAUGGGAUAAUCAGUGUUAUUUUAGGGUGGGAAAAUUUCCACCAUACCUGCUAGGAGAAGGGGAUGGCCAAAGAGUUUUUGACUUACAGAGGAGUUUUUUUGUUCUGUUGUUUUUUCCUCAUUGACUCUAUUUCGCUAGCUUUGUCUGAGAGGGGUGCUUAUAAUUCUAUAUGUGACAUAGUAGCUGAGAGGCAAGCUUUGGAGUUGAUAGACCCAGGUUCCAGCUCUGCUGCUUUGUGAUUUCAGGCAAGUUAUUUAUUCCAUGUGUGUUUCUUUUAAAACUGGGAUGAUAAUAAUAGUACCUGUUUCCCUUAUAGAGUAAUUAAGAGGAUUGAGUGAGAUAAUGCAUGUAAGCCUUUAGCACAGUGUCUGCCUAAGUUAGCAUCCAGUAAAUGUUAGCUGCUGCAAUAAUAAGAAAUAUUAUAGUAUUAAGUUAUUGUUAUUUCUGUGAGGGUGCUGGUUUUCUGAAUGCUGAGACAUUGGUGAUCUUUGCUCCUGAACGUGUUACUAUUUGGAAUACUGCCUUUAUUCAGCAGCAGAUUCAGUUCAGAUUUACUGAACACCUACUAUGCCAGGAAUUGAUCUAAAUAAGCAAAACAAAAAUCCUGCUCUCUUGAAACUUACUUUCUGGUUAGGAGAGACAAAAUACACAAAACAAAAUAGAUGAUGUGUCACUCAGGAAAUUUGGUUGUUGGACUUUGUCUAAGCUUUCAUUAACCAACCCUAGCAGUCUUAACCUUUACAUACUUUUUGAUUGUUCCUGUUGCUGUGCUUGAGAGUGUUUGGAGGUAGGGGCACCCUAAAAGCGUAUCAUAGACUAGCUUUAUUGUCUCCAGCUUCAGCUUGAUCCUAAUUUUAAGGCAGCCUUAAAUGAUAGUUUUCAUCAUUUCCUUGACUUACUACUUAAAUUGGCUAUCUCAAAACUUUCAGUCCCCAAAACUUGUAUUUCACAUCAUUCAGAGAGAUGUUGCUCCUCCCCAGCUGCUCCUCUUUUGCUCUUCUAUGCCAUUUUCUUAAGAGGAGGGGAUACUAGAAGCAUCUUUUUAGAUUUAUUUUCUGACUAGUCUAACUGUAUACUUUUCUUUCUCAUAUUUUGUGUUUUCUACCCUUUAUUUAUUGUUAACUGAUACAUUUAAUUUGCUUAUUUUCUUUAAAAUAUGUGUUUUUUUUGGUCUCUCCAAUUAAAUUGUGAAAGUUUUUAGGUCAGGGACCACUUUUCUAUUUUGACCUUGAGCUUACUCUCUUGAAAAAAAGAUAAUACCACCCAGGGAUGUUGUGAGACCUCAAAGAGAUAAUGUGUGAAAGGGGUCCUGGAGCCAGAUCCUUAAUAAAUGUUAGUUUCUUCUUUGAACCACUCUAGUUGCUGAAACUGCUGUGCAUAUAAUCAGUGCUUAAAAAAUGCUUGUUAAUUUAUCUUGAAUUGAGUUUGUGAACUUUCAAUUGUCACUUGGUGGUAGUUUUAGUUUUUAGUGCUAGAUAAGAUUCAAAAUACUACUUUUCAAGUGUCAGAUGAUAAAUGCUGGGUCAUUAGUGGUAGAGCUCAACAGUGAUUAGGAGCAGGAACUUGAGCCAUCAUUGUUUGGGUUCAAGUACAGGCUACCACACUUACUGGUUGUAUGACCUUUGGCAAGUUGUUUAACCUCCCUCGGUUUCUUUAUCUGUAAGGAGGGGAAAAUGAUAUCUACCCACCUCAUGGUUACUUCUUUGUUAGUAUUAAACGAAGUAAAUGAGAAGCUCGAAACAGUGCUUAGUAUAUAACAAUCUAUAACAGGGUCCCCAGGGGACAUUUGGCACUAUUUGGUGAUGUUUCUGAUGGUCAUUUGGGGGAGUGGGGAGAGGGAAGGGUGCUACUGGUAUCUCGUGGGUAGAGGUUAGGUAUAAACAAGGUAUAGGACAGCAUCCACAACAAAAAAAUUACCUGGUCCAGAAUGCCAGCCCUGCCAAGCAACAUUGGGAAACCCAGCUUAGUUCCUUUGUAUAAGGUACUUUGCCAGUUAGAUUCUGUAUACAUGCUGAUUAUUGAUAAAGAUGAGUCACAGACAUGGAUAGGCUUCAUUUAACAUUCAUUUUAAAAGACAGACAUGUAAGAAGGUUAGUAGGUUUCAUUUCUUUUUAAGGUUACAGGGAAAGUACUCCAAAAUUAAUCUAAAAGUCCUUACACUUUUUUCAGAAACUGAGAAAAGGUUCCAGAUGAAUUUUACUAAUUUAAUUUUUUUAUGACGAGCUAUUCAUGUAAAAGUGUAUUAUGAAUAGAGGGCUUAUGAGAUAUGAGUGCCGUAGUGUGUAUUCAUAAAGUCAAACGUACACUUAAAAAACAAGUAUCAAGGUAAAUGGAAUGAUCUAUUGGGGGAAACCUUGGAGCUCUCUCUCUUUCCAUAUGUUUUAUUACUCACCAAGUCAAGGGCUCUUUAACUUAGGAUCUUGUUUUUCUGUGUACACUUUUCCUGUUUACUGUUUAAAAUUGGACCCUUACUAAAAAUACAGAAAAUUAGCUGGGCAUGGUGGCGUGCACCUGUAAUUUCAGCUACUGGGGAGGCUGAGGUAGGGAGAAUCGCUUGAACCAGGGAGACGGAGGUUGCAGUGAGCUGAGAUCGCGCCAUUGCACUCCAGCCUGGGUGACAGGGCGAGACUCAGUCUCAAAAAAAAAAAAAAAAAAAAAAAAAAAUUGGACCCUUACCAUUCCUUGUCCAUUUCAGGAGCCUCUUAAUUGCCUUGCUUCUGUUCUUUCUCUGUAUUCCCACUUGAAUUGACUCUUCUUUGCUGGGAUCCCUUUGGGAUCCCUUCUAGUCCAGAUCCAAUCUACCCUUCAGAGCUCCUUCCACCGUCCCCUUAUUUCUGGGAGAGAAUUCAGCCUUAAUACCCUAAGGAUGGAAUUUGAAUGUACUGACUUUUCUGCUAUUUACAGGGUUGUGUAUUAUCUUUGGAAGAAUUGGGAAGUCAUAUCAUUUUCUGUAUGUUGUGGUUCAGGUGACUUGUUUCACUUGUAUCCAAACACUGGUUGUGUGUCCAUGUAUAUACAGCAUGUAUGUACUUUAAUGUCUAUUUGUAUGUGUGUGUACAUGUAUAUUCUUUCAUGUAUAUUUGUCUCUACACCUUGCUGUUUCCUCUGCUUGGAAUAUUCUUUUCUUUUCAUCUGGGAAACAUUUGUCUCUUCAGACCCUACUUAAAUAUUGAUCUCCUAGGAAGUGUGUCCUGAUUAAUAUAACUAGAAUUAGUUAUUUUUUUCCACUGGUUACCCACAGUAUCUCUGUGGCUUUUAUAGCACUUAACAUCCUUAUUUGUAUUUUUCUUUUCUACUGAUCUCUCAGUUCUUUGAGGGCAAGAGUCUUGUCUUAGUCAACACCUGCUCCCCCAAGUACCUAACAUUCCUGCCACAUUGUAGACAUAUAGUAUGUUAACAAAUGAAUGGGAGAGACAAAAAACUGGAAAGCUUUUAAAUAAGUUCUAUGGGGGUUGGCAGGAGGGGAGACCACACAUUAUCUUGUCACCUUUGUUUCCAAGUGCUUAGUGUUGUGCUUGCCCAUAGGUGUUCAGCAAAUAUUUGUUGAAUGAAUUAGAAGCAAAUCCCAGGAGCUGAUAAAAUUUUCAUGUGAACUUUUUUCUUCUGCAUUUCUAGAAAGCAUAUCCUAGAAGUAAAGUAGCUUAGAUAUUUUGGAACAUCUUAUUCUUAAAGUCGACCUUCCUAUUUUUGACUCAGUAGUGAAACUUUGAUCCAAUGGAUACUUCCUGAAUAGUGCUUUUGGCUGAUUCCUUUUUCACAACAUAGGUCCGUUCUGGUGUUGAGUUUGUUGGAAAGAUGAAUAUGUAGUAUCAUUUUUACAUCAUGGAGGAGCCAUCAUUAAGUAACAGUGUUAAAUAAGGACUGGUCCCCUUUGCACAUUUGGGCCCAAAUUAAGUGAGUAUGUACUCUUAAGUAUGGGUAAUGAUUGAGGCUAUUGAGGUGUAGGAAAGAAAGAGGACAACUGGAGGUGAAGAAGUGACCUACUAGAUCUCUUUUGCUUUUGGUAAUGAUUGAUUUUUUUUUUUUUUUUUUUUGAGACGGAGUCUCGCUCUGUCGCCCAGGCCGGACUGCGGACUGCAGUGGCGCAAUCUCGGCUCACUGCAAGCUCCGCUUCCCGGGUUCACGCCAUUCUCCUGCCUCAGCCUCCCCAGUAGCUGGGACUACAGGCGCCCGCCACCGCGCCCGGCUAAUUUUUUGUAUUUUUAGUAGAGACGGGGUUUCACCUUGUUAGCCAGGAUGGUCUCGAUCUCCUGACCUCAUGAUCCACCCGCCUCGGCCUCCCAAAGUGCUGGGAUUACAGGCGUGAGCCACCGCGCCCGGCCGGUAAUGAUUGAUUUUUUACCCCCAGUUAUUUUUAAAGAAUUGGCAAGGAAGGAGAGGGGUAUGAAUCUAGAAGAUAAGAAUGUAGAUUUUGUAAUUCAUGAUCAUUAUUAUUACCAUGUAUUGAAUGUUUACUGUAUGUCAGGAACUGUCCUAAGGAUUUUUACAACCGUUAUUUAACUUAGUCCUCACAGCAGUUCAUAUGAAAUAGCUACUGAUGUUUUAUGGCAAAGGAAACAAAUUCAGAGAAAUUUCCAAGAACACAUCGGAAUUUUGACUUGCAGAACUGGGAUUCAAAUCUAGAUCUGUCAUACUCCAUGGUCUAUGCUUUUAAUCAUGCAUGCUGUCUCUUAAGUUUUUAUUGAAAAUGGAAAGUUGUACUGACAUAGGAGGGGAAAAUGAUAGAAAAUCAUCCUAUUGGAAGGCAGAUUAACAGACUCGUGAAGAAGCAAUUCCCAGUUUUAUGUCAUUAUACAAAAUAAUUGUGAAAUUGAAGUCCGUCAUUUGAAUUGAUUUGCAUUAACCCUCAUUUUUUAGUCUUGCUCUUGGAAUCAUCAUCAGGACAGGUGUCCCAGAUAUGUUAGCAGUAGAAUAAAUUUAUCUAGGCAAAAUCUGUCUAAGAUUAUGGAGAAAACUGAUUUUAUAUGUGAAAUGUGUUGUUGAGUGAGAGUUAAAUCUUUUGAAGGAGAUUAUUUCAGGAUGAGCCUCAAAUACAUUAUUUAGGAUUUGAAAACCUAUGGUUUAGCAGAAAAUCUGAGAAUCAACAUUUGUUAGUCUCUUGGGUAUAAAUUGCUUAAGUCAGUGGGUAUCUGAUUAUUCUUUCUUUCUUUCUUUAUUUAUUUAUUUAUUUAUUUUUGAGACAGAGUCUCACUCUGUAGCCCAGGCUGGAGUGCAGUGGUGUGAUCUUGGCUCACUGCAAGCUCUGCCUCCCGGAUUCACGCCAUUCUCCUCCCUCAGCCUCCUGAGUAGCUGGGACUACAGGCGCCCACCGCUACGCCCUGCUAAUUUUUUGUAUUUUUAGUAGAGACGGGGUUUCACCGUGUUAGCCAGGAUGGUCUCGAUCUCCUGACCUCGUGAUCCACCCACCUUCACCUCUCAAAAUGCUGGGAUUACAGGCAUGAGCCACCACGCCUGGCUUCCCUUAUGUAAUUUCUUAAACUAUUUUUGUUUGCUGAUUUGGUGUUUGUAAUUUAAAAAAAAUUUAUUUUUUCUUCUUUUACAUACUUUGUAGAACUAUUCCCUACCCAGUGAGUUUAUUUAUAGAUAUUUCAUAUUUAAUUAAUACUGUGAGAACAUAGUUUUUAUAUCUGUAUUUUUGUUUUUUCAUUAGGAUAUUUAAAAUAAUUUUUGUAAUUCUGUUACCUUAAAAAGAGCUAAACUUAGAUGUUGGCCUUUAAAAAUGUUUUGUGAAAGAUUUUCUCUUGGUUCCAUUUAAAAUACUGUAUUUGUAACUAUAGUUAAAUACAUUUGAACUUUGCCCUUUUCAGAAAUUUUAAUUAUAUGCCUUUAUAAAAUUUUAUCAAAAGUUACAUGCAAAUACUAAGUAUAGAGUGCUGAAGCUGAGCGUGAUGGCUUAUGCCUAUAAUCCCAGUUACUCGAGAGGCUGAGGCAAAAGGAUUGCUUUAGGCCGGGAGUUGGAGACCAGCCUGGGCAUCAUGGCAAAACCUUGUCUCUACAAAAAUAAAAUAAAUUAGCUGGGUGUGGUGGUGUGCACCUGUAGUCCUAGUUACUUGGGAGGCUGAGGUGGGAGGAUGGUUUUGAGCGUAGUAGUUCAAGACUGUAGUGAGCCAAGAUCCUGCCACUAUACUUUAGCCUGGGUGAGAGAGCAAGACCCUGUUUCAAAUAUAUAAAUAAAUAAAAUAGUAGGCUGGGUGCAGUGGCUCAUGGCUGUAAUCCCAGCACAUUGGGAGUCCAAGGCGGGUGGAUCACUUGAGGCCAGGAGUUCCAGACCAGCCUGGCUGGCAUGGUGAAACCCUGUCUCUACUAAAAAUAGAAAAAUUAGCUGGGUGUGGUGGUGCGUGCCUGUAAUCCCAGCUACUCUGGAGGCUGAGGCAGGAGAAUUGCUUGAACCCGGGUGGUGGAGGUUGCAUUGAGCUGAGAUUGCACCAUUGCACUCCAGCCUGGGCGACACAGCGAGACUUUGUCUUGAAGAAAAAAAGAAAAAAAUAAGUAUUGAGUGCUGAAUGAUGUUCUAUAAAAGAUUAAAAAUGCCUAAGUGGAACUAAAUUCUGGUAAAUAGAAUUUAGGGGUUGGGGUAGAAAGAAUCAGAUAAGUACUUCAAGAUUUUCAGACUUUAAGUCUAAGGCUCAUUAGUAUCCUCUGACAUAAUCUACUACAGGUUUCCUUUCUUAGAAGUGAAUGUUAAUAUGGCACCACUAUACAAAUAAUAUCGAUAUCGGUAUUUGAGUGUUUAUUAUGUGACAGGCACUGUUCUGUGUCCUUCAUGUGUAUUACCUCAUCCAGUCCUCACGAUAGCUCUAUGAGGUAAGUGUUGUUAAUAUCCCUAUUUUAUAGCUGAAAAUUUGGCAUAGAGAAGUUAAACAUGGUCAAGGUCCCACCUUUAGUUAAUAGUGGAGCUGGGAUUGUUUCCAGGCAGUCUGGCUCUAGAGCCUGGGACCUUAAUCUUUAUUCUAUACUGUCUGUGUCAUCUGUAAAUUUAUUUCUUAUAUAUUAUUUAUAGAACAGUGCCUGGCACACAAUAAGAGCCAUAGAAGUACUGGCUAUUUUCAUUGGCAUUUAAUUAUAUAUGAGGUUGGCAGAGCAUGCAUUAUUAUUCCAUUUGUUUAUUUAUACUAUUAAUUAGAUAGUAGACUUUAUUCAGAUUUCUGUGUUUCCUUUUUUUAAAUAGUCGAGUUUACCGAAGUUCUUAGAAACUGGAUGAUUGCCUCCAAUAAUGUGGCCAUGCUAGAUCUCAAAAUUAACUUUUUUAAAAAAACCACCCCUCCAACUUUAUUUACACUUCCUUAGAAAUGGAUAAAGACCAAGAUUGGGCUUCUGUUUUGAUAUGUCAUUGGUUUAGAAAGGCAGAAACAGCCUGGCACGGUAGCUCAUGCGUAUAAUCCUAGCACUUUGGGAGGCUGAGGCGAGUGGAUCGCUUGAGCUCAGGAGUUCGAGACCAGCUGGACAACAUGGCGAAACCAUCUCUACUGAACAUACAAAAAUUAGCUGGGUGUAGUGGCACUUGCCUGUAGUCCCAGCUACUUGGGAGGCUGAGGCAGGAGGAUUGCUUGAACCCAGGAGGUCGAGGCUGCAGUGAGCCAAGAUGGUGCUACUGCAGUCCAGCCUGGGUGACAAAAUAAGACCCUGUCUCAAAAACAAACAAAAAAAGCGGAAACAACCAUACUAAGUUUACAGUAUUGUUUGUGUGCCUACUUGGUGGAAGAAAUAAAUUCUUAGAAGUUACACUUUCUUUAAAAAAUUAAAAAUUAAAAACUGUGCAGUGUUGAGAUUAGUAUUACCGCUUAUCUUGCUGACUUGUGAAAUUGAAUUACAUCACUUAUAAUAAUGUGAAGUUUUAGAAAUUGUUUUGAUGAUAAAGAGUAGCAGCCUUUAAGAGAAAUAAUAUAAACCAUGUUUCCUCAAAUCUAAAUGGUCAUCUGUAUGGUAUUAGUUUUCCAUCGCUCUACAGAAGCAGUCCCCAGCCUUUUUGGCACCAGGGACCAUUUUUGUGGAAGACAGUUUUUCCGUGGAUGCGGGGAAGGAGAGGCAGUGGGGAAUGGUUUGGGAUGAAUCAUCAGGCAUUAGGUUCUCUUAAGGAGCACCUAACCUAGAUGCCUUGCAUGCACAGUUCACAAUAGUGUUUGUGCUCCUAUGAGACUCUAAUGCCACAGCUGAUCUGACAGGAGGCGGAGCUCAGGCGAUAAUACUCCACCUGCAGCUCACCUCCUGCUGUGCGGCCGGGUUUCUAACAGGCCACGGACCAGUACCAGUUGUGGACCCCUGCUCUACAGCAAAUUAACACAAAUUUAGCAGCUUAUCUUACAGUUUCUAUUGGUCAGGAAUUUGGGUAUGGUUUAGCUGGGUCUUUCCUCAGGUUCUCACUAGGCUGAAAUUAAGGAAUCAGCCGGGGCUCCUAUCUCUUCUGAGGCUCUGGGUUCUCCUCCAGGCUCACCGGUUGUGGGAAGAGUUCAAUUCCUUGUUCUUGUAGAUCUGAUGUCCCUGUUUGCUUGCUGGCUGUCAGCCAGGGACCACUUUGAGCUCCUUAGAGGCCCACCCCCGCCACCAUGUUCUUGCCAUGUGGCCAAGUUAUUAUGUUGUGUAUGACUAAGGAAGAAAAAUGCUGGAUUAAAAUAUAAGACAAAUUCUUACUUUAUGUAUGACUAAGGAAGAAAAAAUGUUGAAUUAAAACAUGAUACAACACAUUAUUGCUUGGACAGUGCCUUGCAAAAAAAAAAAAAAAAGAGAGUUGUGGUUAUUCUUCCAGCCACAAUAUCUGCUUCAGAAAUGUCAAAUUUAUUUUCUACUGUUGUGUUUGUGUUCUUUUUUGUAAACAACUUUUUUGUUUCAAUGCUGAAUCAUAGUAUUUUACAGGACAUUUAAAAUUAAGAAGUAAGCGUGACUUCUUAUUGUACUACUAAAUGUACAGAAUUUAGUAAUAAUUAUGGUGAUAUAAACUGCCAUUACCCAAUUUGCAAGUGUACAGGGAAUGACAGCUAUGUUGUGACUGCCAUGGGCAAAUGGUGAUUUGUAAAGCAUUGUUGCUUUUUUCCCCCCAUUUUAAGUUGAUUUUAUUGAGAUAUAAUUUAUAUACAGUAAACUACAAGACAUUUCUGUCACCCUCAAAAGAUUCCUCAUGCCCCUUCACAGUUAAAUCCUUCCCUGCACCCUCGCUUCAGGCAAUCAAUGAUCUGCUUUUUUAUUACUACAAAUUAGUUUGCAUUUUUUAGUAUUUUAAACAGUGAGGAAAAAAGAGGAGAUGGAGACAGGCUAUUUUUAAUUUUUAUAUUUUCUUCUUUGUUCUUAGAGAAAUCCUAGUUUCUUUAUUAGGCAUUAGGUUUAUUCCUUCAGUGUGGGGGUAAAGUGAUUCUUCUUGAAGCUUUCUAAGUAUGUUUCCUAGAUGUUCUUGACCUCUGUUUUGCCUAAGAUAACUUUUCUCCAGCAUACCCAGAGUUGGCUCUCUUAAACCAUACGUGCUUGUGUAGCUCCCUCAUCCAUAUUUCUACUUAUUGUCUUUUCAGGACCGUAAACAGAGGUAUUUUUGACUUGACAUUCUCAGCUCCUAAAUAAUCUUAUAGUGUUACUGAGGCUUUUCACCUGUCACAUACCCCCGUCCUAGUCUCUUUUUGUGUUGCUGUAAAUACCCGAGGCUGGGUAAUUUAUGAAGAGAAGAGGUUUAUUUGGUUCAUGGUUCCUGCAGGUUGUAUAAGAAGCAUGAUGUCAGAACAUCUGCUUUCUGGUGAGGGCUUCAGGAAGCUUCCACUCAUGGCAGAGAGUGAAGGGGAGCAGGUAUCACAUGGUGAGGCAGGAAAGGAGAGAAAGAGGAGAGGGGGUGCCAAGCUCUUUUUAUCAGUUCUCAUGAGAACUUACAGAGGGGAAACUCAUUCAUUACCUUGAGGAUAGCACAAGCUGUUUAUGUGGAAUCUGCUCCUAUGACCCAGGCACCUCCCACUGUGCCCCACCCUCAACAUUGGGGAUCAGAUUUCAACCUGAGAUUUGGAGGUGUCAAAUAUUCAAAUUAUAUCAUCCCCUAGAGAACAUACCUCCCCACCCCUGAGAAUCUCAGAAUUUCUUGUUGAGAAUUCAUAUUACAGUAUGAGUUGUAGGAAACAUGAAGGAAAGAUUUCCCUUCUAGUCAGUUCUUAUAUUUAUCACUUGUUUCAUGCUCCUUGGUGUGUAUAGUGUUUUCAGGUGCAGGAAAUGCUCUGGGAAGAAUGUUGCUUCUUAGAACGUAAGAGAAAGGGAACCCCAAGGGAAGACUCAAAUGAAGUCCUUAAAAAGCCCACUUAGCUUCUUCUGAGACAGCAUUGUCCAAUGGAAUGCAAGCGAGAUAGUUAAAUUUAAAUUUUCUGGUAGCUAUGUUAAUAAAGCAAAAAAAGAACCAGCCAACAUUAAUUUUAAUAAUAUAUUUUAUUUAACACAAUAUAUCCCAAAUGUUAUUUUAACAUGUAAUCAAUAUGAAAACCAUGAAGACUUUGAUAUUUAAAAUUCUUAUUUUAAUACUAAAUCUUUGAAAUCAGUGUAUAUUUUAUACUUACAAGACAUCUGAAUUUGGACUUAGUCACAUUUCAAGUAAGUGCUCAUUAGUUAGUGACUACCUUAGUGGACAGUGUAGAUGUAGAUUAUGAACUUUUUAGGAAAAGACAAUAGCAUGUGGACUCCACAAGAAAUUGUCUUUAACAACUGUUUGACUCUCAUAGGUUAGGGCUUUAGUGUUUCAGAAUGGUUUCUAUGGUUGAGAUGUAAAGUUUUUUAUUUUUAUAAAGGUAAGUACAUUUUUAUACAUUUUCAUUAUACAAGUAAUGUCAUUGUUGAAGAGUUGGAAAAGUCUGGGUAAAAGACAACAAAUUGUCCUCACUUCCUCAGUCCAGAGAUAACCAAUGGUAAACUUUAUUGAAUUUCCUCUUUGGGAAUGUUGCUUUUUAAAAUCAAAGAGAAAAUAGAUUUCUUUUUUGUCAUAAUUCCUUCCUGUUCACAUUCAGACAUACAUUAUUAUUGACAAUUCUUUUACCUCUUUGUUUAAAUUUAUGUAUUCUUUUUCUCGGGCUGUAUCCUCCAAUAGGGUCUCUGUGAGUGGAGUACUCUGGAGCACAGUAACCUGAAUGGUGCUUCCCUGGAUUAGGGUUAACAAUAGAAACUUCAAUGGCUUUUAUGUACUCAUUGCUAAACCAGUGUAGUUGCUUUCUAUUUUAACUAUCUGCGAUCUCUUUGCAUAUCCUGCAGCUUUUUUAGUUAUUGAGGUAUAAUUUGCAUACCAGAAAAUUCACUCUAUUAAAUACUCAAUUCAGGCCGGCAUAAUUUGCAUACCAGAAAAUUCACGCUAUUAAAUACUCAGUUCAGGCCAGGCGCAAUGGCUCAUGCCUGUAAUCCCAGUUUGGGAGGCUGAGGUGAGCGGAUCACCUGAGGUCAAGGGUUCGAGACCAGCCUGGCCAAUAUGGUGAAACCCCGUCUCUACUAAAAAUACAAAAAUUAGCCGAGCAUGGUGGUGUGCGCCUGUAGUCCCAGCUAUUUGGGAGGCCGAGGCAGGAGAAUCGCUGGAACCUGGGAGGUGGAGGUUGCGGUGAGCCGAGAUGGUGCCAUUUGCACUCCAGCCUGGGCAACAGGAGCAAAACUCCGUCUCAAAUAAAUAAAUAAAUAAAUAUUCGGUCGUUUUCAUUGUAUUCACACAGUUGUGCAGUAAUUAUCACUAUUAAUCCAGAACAUUUUCAUUACCUCAAAAGAACCCUGAUGCUCAUUAAGGAGUCACUUCCCAUUUCCUCUUUGCGCAGUCUCCUGGCAACCACUAAUCUACUUCCUAUCUCUAUGGAUUUGCCUAUUUUAGACAUUUCUUAUAAAUGGAGUCAUACAGUACAUGGCCUUUUGUGUUUGGCUUCUUUCACGUAACACGAUGUUUUCAGUGUUCUUCUGUGUUGUAGCAUGCAUGAGAACUUCAUUCUUUUUAGGACUGAAUAGUAUUCAGUUGUAUGGAGGGUACCACAUUUUAUUCAUCAGUUGAUGGACUUUGGGGUUGUUUCUGCUUUUUGAGAUCACAUUCAUUCUUCAAGAACAUUAAUUUCUUAAUAUCGUCCUCCAUUCUUAUCAAAGCUUUCAGUGGUUUCCUGUUGUCUAUAAACAUAAUAGAAAAAUAUUUAGUUUGCAUUCAGUCUUACAAAGUGUAACUUCAAGUUACUUUCUUUUCCACUCUUAUUUUCCAUCUUGUUGUUGUUUACUGUGUCUAAAAUAUGUGCUAUAUAUGAAUUAUAAAAUUAUGUAGACAAUAUAGAUAACCUUGUCAUCUGAUCUAAUUUUUAAAAAGUGAAUUUGAAUACUGCCAAACUAAGGAGUAUGUGUAGUAUGGAGAAUUUGAGAAAGACAAGUAUCAGUAAAGAAGAAACAGUAUAGUAAAACAAAAUUUUUUUCUGCCUUGGUCCAUUGAAAGAAAUAUUUAGUUUCAUAUAAUGUGAACAAAAACCUUAAUUUUGAAUGAACAUUUGAUACAUAGGAACUCAUUCAAAUCAUUGAUUUUCUGGUUAACUUUGUUAGUAGUUUGUUUUUUUCUGAGUCUUUUGUUUUAAUCCAGAUAGUCAGUCUUUUUCUCCUUUUUACAUGCUUGAAAUGGUAAAAAUGAAAUAUUUUUACUUAUUCUUAAAAAUAUUUCCAGAAUGUCUUACACACACAUACACUUAGAAACAAAUACAAAUAUAUAGUGAUAUUCUCUCACAUUUUACAGAGAAAAGCGUAGUAUACAUACUUUGUUUUUUAAUUUCACAGUAGAUCUUAGAGGUCUUUUAAUAUUAGCAUACUGAGAACUUUCUCAUUUUUUUCAUAAUAGUAUUGUUUAUUCCAUUGUGAUGAAUAUGCUAUUGUUUUUGAAACUAGUCCCAUAUUGGUGGACAUUUAGGUUGUUUCCAGGUCCACUAUUACAGAUAAUACUACAGUGAAUAAGUUUGUACAUGUAUCAUUUCAUAUGUAUGCCAAUAUUUCUGCAGGAUAAUUUCCCAAAAGUGAAAUUGCUGAAUCAAAAGAUAUAUCCACCUGAAAUUUGAUUACCCAUAUUUUUAAGCAUAAAGGAAGAGAUAAAGGGAAAUAAAUAGAAAAAAAAGAAACUAUAGAUUUUCAAAAACUUUGUUUAUAGAUGAAAAAAUGGAGGAUUAGAACUUUUAAGUAAUUGUCCAUGGUCAUGCACUCCACAGAGGACUGGGCAUGGUGGGAUUCGGUGGGGGGGGCGGGGGGCUGUGUCAGGAUGCUAACCCAGGUGUUCCUGAUUUUAAAUAAGCUGCUAUCCUUCCUGUUAUAUUCAUACUGCAUGUUAUGAGCAAAAGGGGAGAGAAGUCGCCAACUUUUUGGAGAAAAAGAAUAAAAUCCCAGACUUUAUUUUUGGGAUCAUCUGAGGUGGGAAGAUGGCUUGGGCCCAGGAGUUUGAGACCAGCCUGGGCAACAUGAAGAGACCCCCUGUCUCUACAAAAAAAAAAAAAAAAAAUUAACCGUGGUGUUUGAGGCUUCAGUGAGCUGUGAUCACUGCACUCUAGCCUGGGUGACAGAAUGAGAUCCUAGUAUAUGUAGGUAUUUAAUGUAUAUCGAAGGCAGCAUUUCAGAUUGGUGGGGGAGAAGAUGGAUUAUUUGGUAAUUUAUAUUGCAGCAACUUUCUAUUCAUUUGGGGAAAAAGCCCUGUCCCUUGCUCUUACUCUUUACAUAAAAAAUAAUUUAAAAAUGAAAGCAAAAGGUAAUAUCGAAGGAUGUCGUGAGGUUAGCCUUAUUCAAUAGACUGACCUCAGUGAGUACUGAACUCAUGAAAGUUUCAUUUUUUUCCCAGUCACUGUCUUUUGCAUUUUCCUUAAUUGAUUUUUAACAUCACCUUGGAUUAAUCUCAUAGCUUUCCCAAUAUGUUUUUAGUUAUGAAAAGUCUAUUUCUCCUCUUGCCCCGUAUUAGGCUUGACCUGUGGCUGGAGAGAUCUGUGGUACUGUUUCAUAUGUACCGCCCUCCUCUUUCUCUCCUCCCUUUUUUACUUGUUCUGAAAACAAUGAGUAAGGUUAAAAAAUUAUUUUUCACAAACAUGAAAAAGGUUGAUAAUACGUAAGUUUUGAAUAUGGGGGAAAGUUACUCUCAUACUGUUGUUGGGAGUAUACAUUUUUGUGGCCUUUUUGGAGAGCAGUUUGACAGUAUUUAUCAAAAUAAAGUACACAGGCAUCUUGAAUCAGCAGUUGUUCUUCCAAAAUUUAGUAGUACAGAUAUACUGACAUAACUUUACUUGAAAGAAGAAUCCUUUUUAUAACUUAGUGUUUAUUGACAAGAGAAUUAGCAUUUAGAGUCAUUUAUUAUUCUAACUCUUCUACCAAAAUGGUGAGAUGUGUUGUAAUUUACUGGACGUUUAGGUUGUUCCCAAUUUUUUUGUAAGUAUGAAAAAUGCUGCAGUGAACAUCUUUGUCUGUGUGCUACCCAGUCAUCACUGUUGAGAAUGUUUCUUAAUGGCUAUAUUUAGGUAAGUGUUAUUUCCCUUUAUUUCCCCUCUUAUACUUUAAGGAGCACAGGAGAUCUCAGUUUUAAUCGCAGCUCAAUUGCCUAAAUGGAUGUGUGACUUAAAACAAGCUCUUUAACCUUACUGAGCAGGAGGUUCUGCAGAUAUGGGCCUCUCAGACUAUUUUAUAGCAGUAAUAAAUGGACUACCUAUUGUCACAUUCUUCAUGAUCCUGUAGGGAGUAUGUGUCAGUAGGACAACCCAUUGAGUGACAGUCCUAACUUUCUUGGUUCCUCUCCCUCAUUGUGAGGUCAUUGUUUCACAAUUGUAUAUACUUACUGAUUCAAAAAACAACUCCAACACUUAUUGAGGGGUAGUACUGUUCCCAGUUGAGAAUUACUGUUGUAAAAAUUUUGGCAGGAAUUAUAUAAGAUUAUUCAUGAUUGUUAUCGACUUAUCUUUAUUCCUUCAUUUUUUUUUAAAGCAGGAAGCAAUAAUAGUUUACGUUCGUUAACCUCAAUAUCUACUCUAAAACAUGUUGUUUUUCUUGUUAUUACCAUGAAAGUCUGGGUUAACAGGAGACGAGACUAGCUUCUUCACAGAUACAUACAUUAAUUUGACAUUAUAGAAAAAUGAGACUGUAUCCUGACUUGCCAGUUUGGUUUUGAUUGGUGGUUUCACCUUUUUUUUUAGACUCAGGAAAACGGUGGCAAAAAUAGUAUAAAGGGUAAAUUCUCAUAUGCCCUUCAUUCAAGUUCCCAAAAUUUAACAUCUUAUGCAGUGACAGAAAAAUUAUCAAAAUCAGGAGAUUAACAUUCAUGUAAUACUGAUAGUCUACAGACUUUAUUCAGAUUUCACCCAUUUUCUCACCAAUGGCCUUUCUCUGGUCCAGGAUCACAAUAUGAAAUUAUUCACGUGUUGUAUUUUAGUUAUCAUGUUUUCUUAGUUUUCUUUAACCUGAAACAAUUCCAGUCUUUCUUUGCCUUUUGUGACUGUUAUACUUUGGAAGAGUACUGGUCAGUAAUUUUGUGGAAUAUUGCACAAUUUGUGUUUGUAUGUUUUCCUAUGAUUCAAUUAAUUUUAAGCAUUUUUGAUUAAGAAUACUGCAAAAAUGAUUUUAUGAAUCUUAUUUAGAGGCACAUGAUGCUGAUUUGUCCAGUUAUCAGUGAUACUAAUUUUCAGUUCCUUUCGUUAAGGUGGUAUCAGGUUUGUCCACUCUAGUUGCUUUUUUUCCUUUGUGAUUCAUAAGUAGUGUUGAUUCAGAUUCUAGGUUAAGAAAAGGAAAAAAAAAAGUAUCCUAUGGGAAGGUACUUAAAAAUAAGUACUUUGGGACCAGGUAAUUAACAUUUCUCACCAUACUCUACCAAUUUUUAACUUCCUUGCUGUUUUUUUUUUCUUUUUUUUUUUUGCAGUGGCACGAUCAUGAGUCACUGCAAGCCUCAAUCUCCUGGGCUCAGGUGAUCCUCCUACCUCAGCCUGUUAAGUAGCUGGGACUGCAGGUGCACACCACCAUGCCUGGCUAAUUUUUCAUAUUGUUUGUAGAGGCGAGGUUUCAUCAUGUUGUCCAGGCUAGUCUCGAACUCCUGGACUCAAGCCAUCCUGUGUUGGCCUCCCAAGGUGUUGGGAUUACAAGCGUGAGCCACUGCCUGGCCCCAGACUUUAACUUUUAUUGAUGAUUUUGUCAUGGUGAUUUUCUGUUUCCAUCAUUUCUUCUGUAUUUACAUUAGUGGUUUUUGGUAAGGAAGAACUUUCCCUUGUUAUGUAUUUAUUUAAUGUUUUAUGUAUAUCAGAAUGGACUCGCGGAUUUUUUUUCCCCUCUUAUAUCAGAUGGACUUACAGAUUCUUCUAUGGAUUUCAUCUAUUAUCAUCAUUAUUUAUUUUGGUGCUCUAAUUAUCCCAGGUUUGGCCCCAUGAAGCCUCUUCAAGGAGGUUCCUGGUCCUUUUGACAUGUCUCCAUCAUUUUGUGAGGGCUUAACUUUUUUUUUUUCUUUUUGAGUCAGGGUCCUGCUGUGUCACUCAGGCUGGAGUGCGCAGUGGUAUGAUCAUAGCUCACUGCAACCUGGAUUUCCUGGGCUCAAGUGAUCCCCCUGCCUUAGCCUCCGGAGUAGCUAGGACUACAGGCCAGGUAUGUGCCACCACACCCAGCUAGUUUUCGCCUUUUUUUUUUUUCUCCAAUAGAGACAGAGUCUUGCUGUGUUGCCCAAGCUAGUCUUAAACUCCUGGCCUCAAGCAGUCCUCCCACCUUGGUCUCCCAAAGUGCUGGGAUUAUAGGCAUGGACCACCACACCUGGUCAGAAGGCUUAACUUUCUAGUAGCGCAAAAUGUUCUAGUCUCUUCUUGUGCUUUUCUCUGCCCCAGCCAUGAAAUCAGCCAUUUCACCAAGGAAUAUUGAUUCCUUUUACUGGAAAUCGGAAUUCUUCCAUUCCCCCUGCCCCCAGUACUUGUAUCUUACCAUCUUUUUAAAAGUCUUUGUGUCUUAGAACCGUGUUAGAUGAUCUGGACACAUUACCCUGAUGUACAGAAAUUAGUUUAUACACGGUAAUUCUUUUUGUAGCAGACUGUUUAAUUUGUAGCAGAUUCAUUUUGCACUGAUUAAUCCUGGAGGAUUUCUUCACAAGUUACAUUGUGUCAAAUAUGUUAUUUCAUGGGAACACAAUUGAAUUUUUUCCUUAAUUUUGUUCGGUAUUUGAUAAUAACAAUUUAAAAAACUUUUCUAAGAGCUUCCUUCUAAUAUUAUAUGAUAUAGGAAUGUUUACAUUUCUCAUUUAUUUAUUUGGUGUAGUGAUCUCAGAAGUUUUUUUAAAAGAAAAAUCUUGACUUUGUCUCAGGUACUCUCAGUUCACUUCCAUGUGGGAGGGUCAUUUGCCAUCCAUCCAGAUUACCUUUUUGAUUAGGCUUUUCAGUGUCUAUAAAUAUUUCGGUCUUUUCUGAUCAUUUAAUUUCUAAUACAUGCAUAUGCUCCUAUGUAUAAUAAAUAGACAACUUCAAAUUUGCAGUUUCUAGAUGGUUGGAAAAGGGAAACAUUGUGGUGUGUAAUUUAUCAGCCAUCAGAUCCUAGAUAUUUGAGAUUUUAACUAAGCAAGGUAUUAGAUAGACCAUGUUGUUUUGGCUUCACAGAAUUCAUUCAUAUUGUGCAUUACACAAUCAGUGUGCAUAUUGCACAUUGAUUUUAUCUGUAAGUUGUCUUUAUCAGUGGUUCUCAAAGUGUGGUCCCCUGCUAGUAUAGUAUCAGCCUCACAUUGGAACUGGUUAGAAAUGCAGACUUCUCAGGAUCCACCUAAUUGCAGUAGUUAAUUUUAACAAGCCCUUCGGUGAUCCUGAAACAUGUUACAGUUUGAGAAACACUGCUAUAAUACGUUUCAUUUAAAUUGUUUCAGGUUGUGGGGGUAGGGAAUAAGACUACCAAUUUAUUCAUCUUCUGUGCAAUAUUACCUGUUUACCUAACUCUUAGAGAUAUUAAGAUAUUUUGAAGAAUGUGUCCCAUGAGAUUAUAAUGGAACUGACAAAUUCCUAUUGCUUAGUGAUAUCAUAGCUGUCAUGAAGUCUUAGUGCUGUACCUUACUCAUGUGUUUGUGGUGGUGAUGGUGUACACAAAUCUUCUGCACUGCCAGUCGUCUGAAAGUAUAGCACAUGGCCGGGCGCGGUGGCUCACGCCUAUAAUCCCAACACUUUGGGAGGCUGAGGCGGGCAGAUCACAAGGUCAGGAGAUUGAGACCAUCCUGGCUAACACGGUGAAACCCCGUCUCUACUAAAAAUACAAAAAAUUAGCUGGGUGUGGUGGCGGGCACCUGUAGUCCCAGCUACUCAGGAGGCUGAGGCAGGAGAAUGACGGGAACCUGGGAGGCAGAGCUUGCAGUGAGCUGAGAUCGUGCCACCGCACUCCCGCCUGGGUGACAGAGCAAGACUCCGUCUCAAAAAAAAAGUAUAGCACAUACAAUUAUGUACAGUACCUAAUACUUGAUAAUAAAGGACUGUGUUACUGGUUGAUAUAUUUACAAUACUGCACUUUCUGUUGUUACUUUAGAAUGCACUGUUUGAACUUUAAAAAAAUAAAUUCACUUUGGGAGGCCGAGGCGGACGAAUUGCUUGAGGCCAGGAAUUCGAGACUAGCCUGGCCAACAUCGCAAAACCCUGUCUCUACUAAAAAUACAAAAAUUAGCUGGGUGUGGUGGUGCACGUCUGUAAUCCUGGCUACUUGGAGGCUGAGGCACGAGAAUUGCUUGAACCUGGGAGGCAGAGGUAGCAGUGAGCCAGUAUAGCGCCACCACACUCCAGUCUUGGUGACAGAGUGAGACUCUACCUCAAAAAAAAAAAAAAAAUUGCAAAACAGCCUCAAGAAGGCCCUUCAGGAGGUGUUCCAGAAGGCAGCACUGUUGUUGUAGGAGAUUACAGUUCCAUGUGUGUGAUUGCCUCUGAAGACCUUCCAGUGGGACAUUAUGUGGAGAUGGAAGACAGUGAUAUUGAUGAUCCUAAUCCUGUGUAGGCUUGGGUUAUUGUGUAUAUUUGUGUCUUAAAACAGUUUUGAAAGUUAAAAAAAUUUUUUUUAAAACAGGAAAAAGGCUUAUAAAAUAAGGAUAUAAGGAAAGAAAAUAUUUUUAUAUAGCUUUACUAUGUGUUUUAAGCUAAGUGUUAUUACAAAACAGGCAAAAAAUUAAAACGUUCAUAAAGUAAAAACGUUAUAGUAAGCUGAGGUUAUUACGGAAGAAAGAAAAAAUUUUAAAAUAAACUUAGUACAGCCUAAGUGCACACUGUUUAUAAAGUGUAUGGUAGUAUACAAUAAUGUCCUAGGCCUUCAUAUGCAUCCACCCCAACUGACUCAUCUAGAGCACCUUCCAGUCCUGCUAGCUUAAUUUAUGAUACAGAUGCACCGUUUUACAUUUUAUAUACCUUAUUUUUAAUAUACCUUUUAUAUAUUUAGAUGUGUUAAUAUCAUUGUGCUACAGUUGCAUACAGUAUUCAGUACAGUAACAUGCUGUACAGGUUUGUAACCUGGGAGCAAUAGUUUAUACCAUGGAGAUUUGUGUAAAAGCACUGUGUAAUAUUCACACAAAGAAGAAAUUGCCUGACACAUUUCUCUGAAUGUAUCUUUGUCAUGAGGCGAUGCGUGACUGUAUAAUUUGAGCCACACAUGUUAUUUUAAAAAUUGCAAUACCCUUAUUAAUGUAAAAAGCAGUUGAAUUAAUUUUAAGAUAUUUAGCCUGAUGGAGCCAUGAUAUUACCAUUUCAACAUAAUUUAUAAAAAAAAUUGUUAUUUUAGAUUCUCUUUGUACCAAGUUUUUGAAAUCUGGUAGAUAUUUUAUAUCUCAAUUUCAACACUAACUUUUUACCGGAAGUAAUUGAUCUUCCUUUAGAUUUCAUAAAGUUUAUGGUUGGAAAAGUAGAUUCACAUAUCUAAAUCGUUUCAGACACACUUAAGUAUUUCGCUACCUGAAUUAAGUACCAAAAAAUAAUUUUUCUGUAAUAUUUGCAUCUAAAUUGGUAAAACUGGUUCAUGUUUUUUAGUAGAAUGUAGUAGACUUUGAAGCAAAACUGUAUCCAUUUCAAAAUUGAGCUACUGAAGUUAAGCAAAUUCAUGAACUCUUGUGUCAACUCCGUAUUACUGACAUUAUAUUCAAAAGGAGAUUGGAUGUUAGGCAAAUCUAUAUUAAAUAAAGUGUUUUUCAAUGAUUUUUUUGUAAUUUUUGCAGCCACUUUGCAAAACACUGUCAAUUAAAAUUUAUAUAUGUUGAUUUAUGUUAGAACAAAGUGUAAAAUCUUUUUUAUUGGUUUGUGUUAUGAAAACUUUAAAUUUCAAUGUAAAUUUAUAAGAAAGUUCUUAUAAAAUUUCUGGCAUACCUUCUUCCAGUUUCUUUUUAUUUUACUUUUUCUUGUGUUAGCCUGGUCAUAAAUAAACUCUACCUUUCUUUGGUGCUUCAAGUUAAGCUUGUUCAUAGGCAUUGAGAUGUAAGUGAGGAAACAAAAGAAUACUGCCAUUUUUGUCUUUUAUUACUUAAUAGUGAAAAGCAUCUCUUUCUAAAAUCAGAGUUGACAUUAGAGUAGAUCUUUGUGAAGUUAUUCCACUAUACCCAGUGAGCAAAGAACACAGAUGUUUUAAAUGUAUUGUUUUUUAUUUUUUUAACAUUUCCAUGAACUGGCUAGGAUUCAUAUUUUUGGCAUGUACAUACUGAACAAUUCAACUCUUUACAUAGGGCUUUUCAUAGUCUGUUUCAGAAAGCUGAACACAGAUAUUUUCAAUGUGUAUCAUACAGUGGAAUAAAGGAAUAGGAGAAACAUCAAUUUUUGCUUUUAAAAUUCCUAACAUAGCUGGAGCUGUCUGUUGUGAUAGAAACUAAUUGUUUAAUACCUAGCUGAAAUUCUUUGACAGAGGUAAAGGAUUAAAAAAUAUCUAUGCCACUCUUGAUUUUUUUUUUUUUUUUACAGCUACAUAGUGACAACUUUUUCUUAAGUUUAGAAGUUCUUUCAAAUAAAUUUCACCUAAAAGAUUUAAUUGGGGCCGGGCACGGUGGCUCAUGCCUGUAAUUCCAGCACUUUGGGAGGCCAAGGCAAGUGGAUCUCUUGAGGCCAGGAGAUCGAGACCAGCCUGGCCAACAUGACAAAACCCCAUCUCUACUAAAAAAUGCAAAAAAUUAGCCGGGCGUGGUGGUGUGCAUCUGUAAUGCCAGCUACUUGGAGGCUGAGGCAGGAGAAUCACUUGAACCUGGGAGGUGGAGGUUGCAGUGAGCCGAGAUUGCGCCACUGCACUCCAGCCAGGGCAACAGAGCGAGACUGUCUCAAAAAAAAAAAUUUAAUAAGGUAGUGUCUCUUAUAUCACAUGGCUCAUCUAAAGCUAAAGGGAAAUAGUAAUUUUUCACAUUUUGAAUCUGUUGAUUUUUCGUAUUAUUAGAAAGGUCUUCCAUAUGAUGGAUGGUGUCUUAAUUGAAUAUCUUCCACGUGUUGUAAAGUAUCUAUUUUAGUAUUCCUCAUAAUUUUCUAACAAAAUUUCUAUAAUUGAAAUAAUUUCUUUACCAUCUCUUUAUGUAAAUGUGAUUUUCUUUCUUUUGGCGCAAGAAUUUAAGCCAGUUUAUAGCUGACCAGAGUUACAAGCCCAGAUUUGUUAAAAAGCUUUUAAACACGUUUGUUGUACAUUUACUUCUGACAUUGUUUGGCUAAUUUUGUUGCUUUUCUUCUGAUUGUAGAGCAGAAAGUUCUUAUAAAAUUCACUGUGUAUUUGUUGAAAAUGUCUCCUAAUAUUGUCUACUUUACUUGUAAAACUUUAAAACCCAAGAAAUAGCUUUUAAUUUUGCUCUGUCACAGCUAAUUGUAAUUGUCAUUCAUUAGAAAAUUUCUAGCAUACCUUCUUCCAGUUUCUUUUUACUUUACUGUUCUGGUGGUAGCAUUAGCUUCUGUAUCUCUACUUGAUUGUGUAUUGCUGUAAUGCCUUCUUUUUACUUUUAAAAAUGUGUCCUCCUCUUGUCCAUUCAUUUUUAAAGUAAGAAAAUUAAUUAUAUUCAAAAUAUUAAAAUUAAAAAAAAUAAAAAGUAUUGCGAUUGAGUUACCAGUUGUGAUUUACAUAGGCAUCACUGCAACUUGUGUUAUUUGUGAAAAACGUAUUUAAGUAAACGCAGUACGGUGUUAGAUUGAUGAGUAGAAAAAUACUCAUUCUAACUGUAAAUUAGUUAAUUUUUACUGACUAGAUCAGUAUUUUUAUGUGUAAUACUAGAAAUGACUCACUGUAUCCUGAGAUGUGGAGUAUAAUAUGCAGUACAGUGGUCACAGUGAAAUGUAGUACUGCCAAAAGAAUAAAACUUUCUUUAGUAGAAGGACAUUUUACACAGCUUCAGCUUUUAAAUUUAAAUUAAGUACAACUAAAUAAAGCUAAAAACUCAAUUCCCUGGUAACACUAGCCACAUUUCAAGUGCUUAGUAGUCACAUGUGGCUAAUAGCUAAUAUAUUAGAAAUUAAACCUUUUGAGAGUUGGUUAUGUAUGUGAUUAAAGUAUUUUGGUUACUUGGGACUAGAGAUUACAGUCAUUUUUGAUCAGGCUGAUGUCAUAGGAACAGUACCAAGGGGACUUCUGAAUCAAGCACCCUAGAAAGAGCUACUUAGAACUACUUGCAUUUUCUUUGUGGCAUCUCUUAUAGGCAUGAAAAAAUUUCAAACAUUUUUCAUGGAUAAAAGGAUUUAAUCAGAAAAGCAUUUGGAUAUACAUAUUUGAAAUCAUAGCUUGCCUGUAUGUUACUAGAGUAGUUGGAGAGUGGAAAAGUAUCUAUAUUCUAAAGACUGUUUCAUCAUUUGGGUGAAAAACCAAAAAAAGAGAGUAAUUUUGUUUAAUAGCUCUUUCACAAAUAAAAAAAAGAAUGUUCAUCUGUAGAGACCUAUCGAGAUCUCAUCAGGUUUACAACAAACUUUAGAUUAGCAAGCUCAAUUUCAGUUGACAUGGAUUGUGGAAAGAUUUUCAGUGGAGCUCAGAUAUUUAAUAUCCUGAAUUUGGAUGAAUAUACAAUUUCUAAAAUUAAGUACUUCAACUCCUCUGUGGUUUUAAAACCAGUAGUGGCCAUAUCUUGACUAGUUAUUAAAGCACCAACCUUUUUUUCUUUAUUACUUUGCUUUUAUCCUUUGAGCAAGUUAGGCAAUAAGUUCUCCAUGUUUUUGAUUUCUACAGAAGUAAAUGAAUGUUAUUGCUGAUGUUUAUUUCAUUCUGUCUUGAUCUCAUGAUAUGAGAAUAUAAGGAGAUGUCUGAAAACUUGUUUUAAAAAUCCUAUGAAGCAUAAGUUCAUGAAUAAAGAAGGAAGUGGAACUUGUCUUGAGAGAAUUUGCCUAUUUAGAUGGUUUCCAAAGUGCAUUCUGCUAGUCACUAGAGAUGGUCCUUGAAAGAGUUCUGUAAUUAAGUUUGAAGAAACACUGUGUACCAUAAUAAUGGCCUAUUGAAUAUUUUACCAUGCACAUUAAUAUAUCAAAGGCUUUGAGAUAUCUUACAAGAAAGAAACUUGCUAAAGCUUGUCUUCCUGCAUGUCUUAAGCUUCUUCCACAGUGACUUUAAGUCGGACUUGUCUAUCCUGUGAGAAAUGCUGCCCUCUAGAGGCACAAAUUCAAUUGCUCUUAAAUUUGAGUACCAUAAUGCUGCCUGAUCUUAGUGUGAAGUUGUGAUAAUUAAUAUUAAUCAAAUGCAUGGUAACAAAACCAAAUAGAAGAAAUCUUAUGUUGCUUAAUUUUAAGAAAAUAUGAGGAAACAGAAUUGCAAUUUAUAAAUACCCACUUUUUAAAUUGUACAUGUGAUAUUUUUGGCUGCUAAUAAUCUUUUGAAUACAUUUCUGUAUAUGGGGAAUUGCGGACACAUAGUACUUCAAGUCUCCAAACUCUGAGUCUCUCCUGCUAGCAGAAGCCAUCCUUCCCUGUGUUAACAACCUUGCUUAAGACAGUUACCAUCCAUGGGGAAGCUAGUUUCCUCAUACCCCUUCCCACGAUACUCAUGUUUCCAUACCUGUAACUGGAGUCAGACUAUAUCAUGCUGCACCUUUGCAGUCACAAUGGGAAGAAAAGGAUUAUAUGUAAUUUUUUUAAAGUUUUUUUUUUUUUUUUUUUUUUUUGCUGACAAAGCAGCAAAACCUUCAGGAAUAUGUACAGAAAUGGGUGAUGAUGAUGAUGUGAGAGAGAAAGAAACAUGCUUUUGCAUUUGGCUGAAUGUAUUGGUAUGGUGCAGUUAUCAGAGAUUCUGAAUUCAUUGUUCUCGUUCAAGUAGCCAGGAGUGGUUCUAAUUGUUUGCUCCUUUGGUCUCAGCAUUGACUUAUACUAAAUGAAGUUGAAUGCCUAAAAACUCAUAGCAUAAUAUAGAGGAAGAAGUCAAAAGAUUAAAGGAAAUAGAACUGAUGGAGUGGAUUUAUCACUGUGACCAUUCACUUACCUCCCCUAUUCCCUCUCCAGUAUUCUCUACUAAGAGGUCUGGAAGACACUUCAUUCACCAACCUAAUGAGAAAUACUUUGAGGGCAGUGCCAGCAUAUAUGAAAAGUAAUUCAAUUGCUUUUGUCUGUAGGCUGGAGGAGAUACUUUCAUUGAAAUUGUCUUUUUUACUUCAGGGGGUGUGGCCAGAUUCUAGGUAAGGUCCAGGCAUCAUUUUCAUAAGGUAGCUUGACAGGCAUGAUGAUCAGAGAUGCACUGACUUGAAUUCUUUUUGGCUGUGACUAAAUGAUCAUGGAUCCCUACGUCUAAAAUAGAGAGGAAGCCUAUUAAGAUCCUACUUUAUCUGUAUGAGCAAAAAAUUUUAGGUCUCAUAGGAGAAGGCCUUACUUGAACUACCAUAAGAGUGAGUUGGCCAGCCUGGGCAACAUGGUGAAACCCUGUCUCUACAAAAAACACAAAAGUUAACUUUUGUGUUUUGGGCAUGGCUGCGUGAGCCUGUGGUCCUGGCUGCUCAGGAGGCUGCCCCCUUUUUGCAGUUUACUUCAUGGGUUAUAUGAGAAAACAGGAAGGAGGGGGAUAUCACCGAGAGAUUCUGAUAUUGGAGCUGUGUGCAAUAACUGAUAAGUCUCUGGUUCUUACCUCCAUAUGAGGAACAGAGAGAGUCUUGUUUGUACAAGGCUUAGUUAUAAUCUGUCAGGUUUGAGGAUCUUGAUUGGAAGCAUAGACUUGAUCUGUAUUUGUGGUUUCUCAUUUCAAAUAGCCUCUCAAUGUUGGAUAAAUUUGCAUGUUCAUGUUUUAUAGAGUCAGAACUCAAUUUCCUAGUAUUCCUUGCAGCUAGGGCACAAGCAUAUGACCUAGGCUUUAUUGAUCAGAUGCAUCUGUGUAAGACAUGAAUUCAGGGUCAGAGAAAUGCAGGGUAACAGCUCUUGCCUGGAAUUGCUUUCUAAUGUGCAUGUUGAGUGACAAGAUAUUGAGCUGUUUAGAGGUAGCAGUGACAGAGAUACUAGUGAGCCUUGUUGUCCUAGGCUCAGCUUUCAUGGUACUAGGGCUGAAGGAUGGGAACAAUUUGGUGGGGAGACUUAGGUAUUUUUCCUGGCAUCAUAUCUCCAAGUGGAUUCUUCAGUUCUCUGAUAAUUCUUGGAAUCCCCUAAUAUAUUAAUAAAUUUAUUUUCUCUUGAAACCACCUCAAAUAGAUUCUGUUUAUAGCUUAGAGCCCUGAUUGAUCGUCUAACUUUAAAGAUUUUAUUUAUCGUCAAAAUAUUUUAUUUUUCUAAUUGAGAUCUAAAAAUUGUCAAGCACUUAUACUCUAUUUUUUCCCUUCCUAGAGCUCUGCAAUCCUUUGCUGUCAUUUUUUCUUACCAGGAAUGCCAAUUUUUGUACCUUUUGAAUUGCUUUUUCUUCUUUGCUACUUGGCUUGAGCUCCACUAUUGUUAUGAAACCUUUCUUAUACCAUCCCAGCAGCCUGAUGGAUUUUUUUCUUCCUCUGAAUUCCAGUAGCACUUGUUUAGACAUUAAGUGCAAGGUGUUUUUUUGUUUUGUUUUGUUUUUCUGUAUGCAUCUUAGCUUCCGCACUAAAUGAUAAGCUCCCUGAAAACUAGUACUAUGCCUCUUUAUAUCGCUUGCAUUGUCCAACAGAAUGUCUUGCACCUAUUAGAUUCAAGGUUCAGCACAGUCACCCUCAUAAUAUAUAGUGAUGAGAGUUGCUGAGAAUCACAGUGAUGCCAGGCUGAAUGAGCUGAGAUAAUAAACUAGUUAGAUGCAUAGUCUGGCCAUGAGGCCCAAUUUCCAUCUUCCUCAAGGAGUCUGAGACUUGCCUCUCAGUAGUUUUCGUUAGUAGGUGAUCAUAUCUUCUGAAUUACUGUCUUCUUAAUGUUUUAUGAGUUUUUUUUUGCCUUGACAAAAGCCUUCUAUUUCUCUCAUGCUUCCUAGUUCCUUCCAUUGUGCCCUCUGCAAUUUCUUUUCACUAAGCUUACUAUUUGCAGUCUCUUAAAAUUUGUGUAAAUUAUGAAAUCAAAGAUACAAAGAAAGGACAGAAAGUAGUAUAACAAACACCUGUGUAUCUAACCUCAGGGUCAAGCAGAUAUUAACCUUUUGCCUCGUUUGAUUUCCUUUUAAAGUUCUUCCCUCCCCAUACUUUUCUCCCUUCUUUGGAGGUACUCAUUAUCCUAAAGUCCUUACGAUUAUUUCCCUGCUGUUUUUGUACACAUAAAACAUUUACACAAAAGAUGACCUGUGUUUUUUUCUAGAUGUGUUCAUAUUGACAUGUGUAGAUUUAGUUCAUUCAUUGUAACUACUGUUUAGUUUUCCAGGUUGAAUAAUGCUAAGUUUUAUAGAGAUAAUGCAGUUCUACCUUUUGGCAAAUAAUAUUGUAAUGCUCGUACAUAGGUACUUACUGUAAUUUUAUCUAGGAUAGAUACCUGAAAGUAGAAUUGCUGAAUCACAGGGUUCAGGUGCCACUUUAUCAAGUAUUGCCGAGUCCAGUCCAAAGUGGAGCUACCAUUUUAUACCCAUUAACAUGUUUCCACACUUUUUUUUAUCAACAUUUAAUUUUAUCUAGCUAUGAUUUUUUUGCCUAUUUGAAAGAUGAGAAAUGGAGUUUGAUGAUUUUCAUUUUCAUUACUUUGAUUUAUAGUAAAGUUGAAUGUCUUUGCAUAGUUUUUGAUCAUUCUAGUUUCCUAUUCUGUGAAUCUUUUAUGUUCUUUGCUGAUUUUUUUCCUAUUGGGUAUUGAACCUUAAAUUGAUUUGUGGUGAUUCUUUUUAUAAUCUGGAUAUUAAUGGUUUUGGUAAUAUGCAUUGCAAGUAUCUCAUAGUGUGUGUGUGUGUGUGUGUGUGUGUGUGUGUGGUUUUUUUUUUUUUUUUUUUUUGAGAUGGAGUCUCACUCUGUCUCCCAGGCUGGAGUGCAGUGGUGCGAUCUUGGCUCACACAAAUUCUGCCUCCCGGGUUCAAGUGAUUCUCCUGUCUCAGCCUCCUGAGUAGCUGGGAUUAUAGGUGCCCGCCACCACACCUGGCUAAUUUUUGUAUUUUUAGUAGAGAUGGGAUUUCACUGUGUUGUCCAGGCUGGUCUCCAACUCCUGACCUCGGGUGAUCUGCCCGCCUUGGCCUCCCAGAGUGUUGGGAUGACAGGCGUGAGCCAUUGUGCCCGGCCUUCGUGUCGGUUUUUAACAUUGUUUAAAAGUUUCAGAUUUACUACAUGAGUUCAUUUGUAGAAUCUCUCUUCUGUAUCAUAGCUUCUUUGGUCUGCUUUCAUGUCUUUACAAUAUUGUGUUAAUUUUAAUAGUUUUGAUAUAAAUCUUGUUAUCUGAUAAGGUGAAUCUUCUCUCAAUGAAAAUUUUGGGUCAGCUAAUCAUAUUUCACCCUGACCCUAAUGAAAAUUUAACAGAAAACAAACCCUGUUGGAAAUGUGAUUGGAAUCUCAUUGAAUUUACAGGUUACAGUGGGGAUAGUUGUCACCUUUACAUUGGUUGACUGUCAUUGAUAUUUCUGUUCAAUACAGUUCUAUUUUUUUCUUUUUUCUUUUUCUUUUUUUUUUGAGAUGGAGUCUUGCUUUUGUUGUGAUCUCGGCUCACUGCAACCUCCGCCUCCCUGUUUCGAGUGAUUUUGCUGCGUCAGCCUCCCCAGUAGCUGGGAUUACAGGCGCCUGCCACCAUGCCUGGCUGAUUUUUGUAUUUUUAGUAGAGACAGGGUUUCGCCAUGUUGGCCAUCCUGACCUUAGGUGAUCUACCCACCUCAGCUUCUCGAAGUGCUGGGAUUAUAGGCGUGAGCCACUGCGCCUGGCCCAGUUCCAUUUUUUUCUUGAUAGAAGUCUUCAUUAGAUUUUUUUUUUUUAGGUUUUUAUGAUUUUUGUUACCAUCGUGAAUGGCAAAUUUUUAUAAAAAUACUUUUUGUUACUGGUAGCUACAAACCAAUUAGUAUAAGAGACAAAUUGCUAAGAAGCAAGUUGCUGUUUGUAUCUUGAUUUUGUAUCUCUCAAUCUUGCUGAAUUCUUAGUUGUUUUUGUUUGUUUGUUUGAGGUGGUGUGUCUUACUCUGACACCUAGGCUGGAGUGCAGUGGUGUGGUCACUGCUCACCACAGCCUUGACUGCCUGGGUUCAAGCAAUUCUCCCACCUCAGCUUCCCAAGUAGCUGGGACCACAGGUGCAUGUCACCACACCCAACCAAUUUUAAAAUUAUUUGUAGAGAUGAGGUCUUGCUAUGUUGCCCAGGCUGCUCUCGAACUCCUGGGAUUAAGCGAUCCUCUUGCCUUGGCUUCCCAGAGUGCUGAGAUUACAGGCAUGAGCCAUUGCACCUGGCCUAAACUCUUACUUCUAAUGAUAGAUUCUCUUGGAUACCUCAUGCAGAUAAUCAUAUAAGUAGUGAAUAAAGAUGGUUUUUGUUGCUUUCUAAGCCUAUGUCUUUAUAUUUUUCUUCUGUUAUUGACCUAUGUAGGACCACUUUACUAAAAUUGCAGCUUUUCCUGGGCCUUGGCUUUAUGUGUGUGUUAAUGUAUGGAGUAGAAAGGGGUAUCUCAGAACUGAAGUCUCCCACUAAGGGCCAAAAGUCUCAUUUCUAGUCCCUACAUAUGAGUCAAAGGAUAAAUAUAGGUUAAGACUAGCAACCCAUUGUAGGGAAGAAACAUUGCCAACUUGUAGCCUAAUAUAUAUAUUUUUAAUAUGUUACUGUUUUUUCCAUGUUACUGGCACACACUUAAAGAUUUCUGUUUCAUGGUGGCUAAAGGAUUAAUUUAAAAUAAUUUUUUUUUUCCUUUUUGAGUUGAGUUUCACUCUGUUGCCCAGGCUGAAGUGGAGUGGGGUGAUCUCAGCUCACUGCAACCUCUGUCUCCCGGUUUCAAGCGAUUCUUCUGCCUCAGCCUCCUGAGUAGUUGGGACUACAGGUGUGUGCCACCAUACCCAGCUAAUUUGUUUUUUUUUAAAUUUUUAGUAGAGACGGGGUUUCACCAUGUAGGACAGGGUGAUCUCGAACUCCUGACCUCAGGUGAUCUGCCUGUCUUGGCCUCCCAAAGUGCUAGGAUUACAGACGUGAGUCACCACACCCAGCCUAAAAGAAUUAUUUUGAUAUAUCCUUUCUGCAUGAAAUUUCUGUGGGAAGGCUUUUCAGGUGAUCUGAUCUGAUACAGUGUUAGGACUGGAAGUAUAGCUUAUACUAUAUAAAUUUCCUUAAUUGAAAUUUCACAUUAUUUAGGAACUCUGUACCCUGAAGCUGUCUCACUCUGGUAUUUAAUGUCCUACAAUUAGUUUAAGAGAGCAAGCUUGGGUAAGUUUCUUAAAACUUCCUUAUAUUUGUUUCUUCAUCAAUAUUAGUAGUAUAGUAUCAUCUCCUAUCUUAUAGAUUAUUAUAAGAAAUAAGUUAAUAAUGUAAAGCAUUUAGAACAGUAUUAGUUAUUGGUCUCAACCUCCUUUUAGCUGUUAUCUACAGCCUUUCUGGUAGAUUUUACUUAUUCUGGGAAGAUAGUGGUGUAUUCCUCAUAAUCUCCUUGUACAUUCCAGGUCCUACAAUAAUUCUCAAACAUUUUAGCAUCCUUACAUAGACUCUCCAAUAUCCUGGUCUUAUUUCCCUGAUCUCCUCAAAUCUACUGAUUUUUCUCUUCCUCAGACAAGUGAUUUUUCACUUAUUUGGUAAAAUCCUAAUUCUGGAUUAACUCGGUUAUCAGAUUCUUUCAUUCCUAUACCACCUGAAUGCUGCAGUAAAAAGUUACCUCAAAGGACAUUUAAAAAAAAUUAUAAAUUCAUGAUUGUUGAUCACAGACCCUAAUACUGCAUGGGAAUCCACUGCAUUAUCCUUGUCAGCUAGUUUCCUCAUCUUUACCAUGACUGUUUCAAUCAUCUGUUCUCCUCAGACCUCCAACAUGCCCUUUCUCUUUCUACAGAAAACUUUUCCUGUUACUUUCCAGUGAAAACCGGAGUACUUGGUGCAACCCUUAGUUGCCCACUAUCUUUUCUAUAUUUUCUUUCUUCUUAAUGUUAAAAUAGAGGUAGUCUUGCUUUCUAUCUAAGGCUUUCUCCCUUUCUCUGCAGUACCUUAUGCUGUUGAUGAUUUCCCUUUUUUUUGUAUGUUUAACUUUUCUUUACACUUGAUUCUUCUCGUCAGUAUUUAAACACGCUUAAUUCCUGCUAUUAAAAAAAUAAAAACAAUAAGCAUUAAUGGGUACCACAUUACUGACCUUUCUGUUCUCUUUCCUAGCCAAAUGCUAGAAAUUAUUGUUUCCAUUUCUCACCUUUGACUCACCUGUUUAGUUUAUUCAUUCCACUGUAAUAGUAUUUGCUUAUGAUACCAACAACCUCUCUGUUAGUAAAUUAAGUGAAUAUUUUUAAACUUGGUCUUAUUUGAUCUCUCACUUGGUGUGCUAGGGCUUCUAUAAAAUACCACAGACUGGGUGGCUUAAACAACAGAAAUUAAUUUUCUCACUAUGUGGAGGCUGGAUGUCAAAGAUCAAGGUGUUGGCAGGUUUGUUUUCUUCUGAGGCCUCUCUCCUUGGCUUGCAGAGGGUGCCUUCUUGCUGUGUCCUCACUUGGUUUUUCCUCUGUUUGCAUGCAUUUCUGGUGUCUGUGUCCAGAUUGGAUUAGGGCCUGGAAGAUGAAUUUACUCACCUCUCUAAAGGCCCUAUAUCCAAAUACAGUCGUGUUCUGACGUACUGGGGGUUAGGGCUUCAACACGUGAAUUUUGGGGGAGACAGUUUGGCACAUAAUCUCCUAGCAGGUUUAAACAGUUUUGAAAAACUAUCCUUGGCUGGACGCAUUGGCUUACACCUGUAAUCCCAACACUUUGGGAGGCCGAGGCGGGUGGAUCACCUGAGGUCAGGAGUUCGAGACCAGCCUGACCAACAUGGUGAAACCCUGUCUCUGCUAAAGAUACAAAAAUAAGCCAGGUUUGGUGGCACAUGUCUGUAAUCGCAGCUACUCGGGAGGCUGAGGCACGAGAAUCGCUUGAACCUGGGAGGCAGAGUUUGCAGUGAGCCAAGAUUGCGCCACUGCACUCCAGCCUGGGCAACAAAGCGAGAGUCUGUCUCUGGAAAAAAAAACAAAAAACAAAAAAACUAUCCUUUAAACUCUUUGGUUUUCAUUUUGCCUCUCUGAUCUAUUGCUCUUCAGCCUUUUUUUAACAGGCUUCUCUUCUGCUUGGUUAUUAAAAGUAGAAAUUUCUUGAGUCUUGGUCCUUUGGUAUUUUCUGCUUCUCUUACUUCUGUUAUUUCUCCCCAGGCAGUCUUACCACUUUGAUUUCCAUUUAUGAAGGAACUGCAUACCUGUUGUUCCAGCACUUAAUUUGCCUGAGUUUCAGACCUAUUUAAUAAUGCCAUUUAGCUUAUCCUAGAGGUACCUUAAAAAAACGAGUUCAAAUCUGAACUCAUAAUAAUCCCCAUCCAUGUGAUUUGACCCUAAUCUACCUCCUUAGCCUUACUAUUCUUUGUUACUCUUUGCCAUAGCUGCACUAUAGCAAAGCACGGCCUCUUGGUCCAGGCGUAAUAUACCUUUUCCUCCAGAGUCUUUGCUCUUAUUUCCUAUGUUAAUAUGCUCCUCAUUUUUCAUUUACAACAUUACCCAGUUUUCAAUACAUACAAAAGAUAAAAACAUUAGUUAUUAGGGAAAUGCAGACUUAAACCAUAAAAUAAUCACUAAAACCAACUAGAAGGGGUAAAAUUAAAAAGACUGUCAACUACAAAUAUUCUAGGAAGCCAUCCAGAACACUCGUAAAUUGCUGGUGUGAGUAUAAAAUGGGAGAGCCACUUUGGAAUACCACUGGCAAUUUCUUAUAAAUUUAAGCAUACACCUUUGGAUCCAGCAAUUCUACUUCUAGGUGUUUUCGGAAAAGGAAUGAAAACAUGUCCACAAAAAACUUUUAAAAAUUAUAUUUACAGUCGAUUUACUCCUUACAGCUGACAACUAGAAGCAGCCCAAAUGUCAAUAGGAUUAAUGACUAAAAAUUUUUUGGUAUAUUCAUACAAUGGAAUGCCACUCAGUAAUAAAAGAACUACAGAAUGGCAAAUGUACACAACAUGACAUGGAUGAAUCUGACAUACUUGGCAAAGGAAGCUGGACAUGAUACUGUAUUAUUCCAUUUAUAUUAAGUUCUAGAAGAGGCAAAGCUACUCUGGAGUGAAAAAAUAAAAACAGAACAAAGGUUGCCUUUUGCUUCUGGAAAAUGGUGAUAUUCAACUGGGAGGGUGCAUAAGGGGCCUUCUUGAAGUGAUGAAAAUGUUCCAUAUCUCAUAGAGGUGUGUGUUACAUGGGCUUAUCUAUUAAAGUUGUACAGCUAAGAAGUAUGUAUUUCAAUGGCAUACAUGUAUCUUAGAUAAAAUAAACAAGUUUUAUCUAAAAAUUAUAGAAAUAAUUGAGUUAGGUGACAGGGAGUGGGAGGUGUAGAUGAAAGAAGAAUUGCAGAACGUUGGUGGUUGCUGAAGUUGAGUAAUGGAUGUGGGGAAGUUUAGUAUACUAUUUUGUUUGUUUUUUGUGUGUUCAAAGUUUUCCAUAUAAAGAUCUUUUUAAAUCAAAGUUACGAAGACACUUAAACAGCACCUGUGGUCUGACUGCCAGCUUAAUAAAGAAUGCUUACUAAUGUAAUUUUCUUCUCUGUGAAUCGUACCCUGAUUCAGCACUCCUUUCUCCCCACCAGCCACUAUCCUGAAUUCCUCUUGACUUUUUAAGACAUCUUCCAAAUAUCAUUCUAAACGUCACGUCCAUGGGGGAAAGCCUUUUCUGAUUCAGAACACUCACUAGUUUUAAGUGCCCCUGUUAAGUCCUUUCAUAGCUUUUAUCUUAAUUAUGAUUUAUUUGCUUAACUAUUAUCAACCUCUACACUAGACUAAGCCUAAGUUUUUGGAGGGAAAGAUAUAUCUAUUCUUGCUGUUUUAAUGUCUAGAAUAAUAAUACAUUUAUUGAAUGAUUAUGUUGGUGUAGUUUUUUAAAAAAAUUGAAGGAUACCCAAAUUGAAGAGCUAUUCUAUUACUGCUUAUGUUGUAAGGUCAGUAUGUUAUAAAAUGUAUGAAUGUGAGAGAAUGACUGAGAAAUGAUAAUGGUUUCUUUCUGAUUUUAUUGGCAUCUGAUAAAAACAAGGGGCAAUAAAACUGUGUUAUUAGAUCUGGAACUAUAUCCGGAAAGUCCUGUCAGUUGGUUCUCAAAUGCCCUUGAGCUUUAUUAUGCUUCUUCCUUAUUAAUGUAUUAAGCCGUGUGAGUGAAAGACCCCUUUCCUCUUUACAAAGAAUAUUCUAAAUCACCUCUUUUUUCUCUCUUCUCUAAUGUGCUUCUUCCUUUGACUAUUAGUUUUGGUAUUUAUCAGGGACAGCGAUCUUUAAGAGCUUGUUGUUUUGUUAUUUUUUGUACUGCUUGCUGUAUGUUUUAAAUUUUGAUAUAUCUUACUGCCAAAUGAAGGUGUGAGCUCAUAAGUAAUAAAGAUAGAAAAAAUCUGCUUUGCUUAUAAUUAUACCAUUAAACAUGUUGUCCUUAAUGCAGAUACACACUAUUGGUAUUGUAGGUGCAGGAUUAUGUUUUGAUUUUUGCCAGUUCAUAUUUCCAUGGAGUAUUUAGGCAAUUUUAACAACAUAGAUUUCUGUAAUGAAUGUUUUUUUAACUUAUGCUGCUGCUUGAGAGACAGAGUCAGACUGCCAGGGUUUGAGUCCUAUGCCCAAUAUUUCCUAGCUCUGUGACUUUUGAGUUAUCUGCUUUUUGCCUGUUUCUUCCUCAUUAAAACAGAGAUACUAAGUGUACCUUAUAGUGUUGUUGGGAGGGCUAUUUGAGGUAGUAUAUGUAAUGCCUGGUACUUAUUAAAUGUUAGAUCUUUUUUACUUUCUUGGGUUCUAGGGAGUCCAAUAAGUAACAAAUUUUUCCUCUAAGGUUUUUUUCUUUAUUGGUGGCAAAAUAUACAUAGUAUAAAAUUUACAUUUCAACCAUUUUUAAAUAUACAAUUCAGUGGCAUCAAGUACAUUCACAAUAUUUUGCAACCAUCCAUCUCUGUCCAUUUCCAGAAGUUUUUCAUCAUCGCAAAUAAAAACUUGAUACCCAUUAAACAAUAACUCCCAUCUUUCCUCCCCUGAUUUCCUGGUAACGUAUGUUAUACUCUGUCUUUAUGAUUAUGACUAUUCUAGGUACCUCAUAAAUAGAAUCAUACAGUGUUUGUCUUAUUGUCCUCUCAUUUCAUUUGGCAUAAUAUUUUCAAAGUUAAUUCAUGUUGUAGCGACUUCUAGUUCCAUUUUUUGUGGUUGAAGAAAGUACUUCCCUAAUAGAAAUGAAAACAUGUUUGCAAGGCUUUUUUUAAAGAAUGCUUAUGGAUUUAGUCAUAAUAGGUAACAACUGAAAACAUUGGUAUGGCUGGGUCAAGUUGGACUAAUUCACUGUAGCCCAGGGUCAUGUAAGAACAUGGAGUUUUCAAGAAAAUAUAAGAAGCAUGGACAAUCUCAGUAGCAAUGGUUACAUGCAUCUUGGUUGCUAAAUAUGGCUCCCCAUUGAAAGAAUUCAAGAUGUCUUAGAAAAAUAGAUGAUCCCAGUUCUUAGGAAAACACACAGCAAGCCAGAAAACAAGGAAGUGGUGAAAAACUGAGGAAUUAUGUAAAAAAGAACCAACUCAAAGGAGUUCUAGUGGCCACCUCCGAAAUAAUGAUUGCAAUCACAGGCAUAUCUUGGAGAUGUUGUGGAUUCGGUUCCAGACCAUCACAAUAAAACAAAUAUUACAAUAAAGGAAUCUCAACCACCAGCAGGAUUUUAAAAAGGCUAUCUAAAUAUUUGGAUUACUUCCUUAGGAUAGAUUGCCAGAAGUGGAGUUACUGGGUCAGAGGAAUGUGAAAACCUUUGCAUCUUCUGAUAGUCUAGCCAAGGUCCAAGAAGUAGCAAGCUGGCUUUUGGAAAUGAAUCAGGAACUGCUCUCUGUGGGCAGCAAAAGACGACGAACUGGAGGCUCUCUGAGAGGUAACCCUUCCUCAAGCCAGGUAGAUGAAGAACAGAUGAAUCGUGUGGUAGAGGAGGAACAGCAACAGCAACUCAGACAACAAGAGGAGGAGCACACUGCAAGGAAUGGUGAAGUUGUUGGAGUAGAACCUAGACCUGGAGGCCAAAAUGAUUCCCAGCAAGGACAGUUGGAAGAAAACAAUAAUAGAUUUAUUUCGGUAGAUGAGGACUCCUCAGGAAACCAAGAAGAACAAGAGGAAGAUGAAGAACAUGCUGGUGAACAAGAUGAGGAGGAUGAGGAGGAGGAGGAGAUGGACCAGGAGAGUGACGAUUUUGAUCAGUCUGAUGAUAGUAGCAGAGAAGAUGAACAUACACAUACUAACAGUGUCACGAACUCCAGUAGUAUUGUGGACCUGCCCGUUCACCAACUCUCCUCCCCAUUCUAUACAAAAACAACAAAAAUGAAAAGAAAGUUGGACCAUGGUUCUGAGGUCCGCUCUUUUUCUUUGGGAAAGAAACCAUGCAAAGUCUCAGAAUAUACAAGUACCACUGGGCUUGUACCAUGUUCAGCAACACCAACAACUUUUGGGGACCUCAGAGCAGCCAAUGGCCAAGGGCAACAACGACGCCGAAUUACAUCUGUCCAGCCACCUACAGGCCUCCAGGAAUGGCUAAAAAUGUUUCAGAGCUGGAGUGGACCAGAGAAAUUGCUUGCUUUAGAUGAACUCAUUGAUAGUUGUGAACCAACACAAGUAAAACAUAUGAUGCAAGUGAUAGAACCCCAGUUUCAACGAGACUUCAUUUCAUUGCUCCCUAAAGAGUUGGCACUCUAUGUGCUUUCAUUCCUGGAACCCAAAGACCUGCUACAAGCAGCUCAGACAUGUCGCUACUGGAGAAUUUUGGCUGAAGACAACCUUCUCUGGAGAGAGAAAUGCAAAGAAGAGGGGAUUGAUGAACCAUUGCACAUCAAGAGAAGAAAAGUAAUAAAACCAGGUUUCAUACACAGUCCAUGGAAAAGUGCAUACAUCAGACAGCACAGAAUUGAUACUAACUGGAGGCGAGGAGAACUCAAAUCUCCUAAGGUGCUGAAAGGACAUGAUGAUCAUGUGAUCACAUGCUUACAGUUUUGUGGUAACCGAAUAGUUAGUGGUUCUGAUGACAACACUUUAAAAGUUUGGUCAGCAGUCACAGGCAAAUGUCUGAGAACAUUAGUGGGACAUACAGGUGGAGUAUGGUCAUCACAAAUGAGAGACAACAUCAUCAUUAGUGGAUCUACAGAUCGGACACUCAAAGUGUGGAAUGCAGAGACUGGAGAAUGUAUACACACCUUAUAUGGGCAUACUUCCACUGUGCGUUGUAUGCAUCUUCAUGAAAAAAGAGUUGUUAGCGGUUCUCGAGAUGCCACUCUUAGGGUUUGGGAUAUUGAGACAGGCCAGUGUUUACAUGUUUUGAUGGGUCAUGUUGCAGCAGUCCGCUGUGUUCAAUAUGAUGGCAGGAGGGUUGUUAGUGGAGCAUAUGAUUUUAUGGUAAAGGUGUGGGAUCCAGAGACUGAAACCUGUCUACACACGUUGCAGGGGCAUACUAAUAGAGUCUAUUCAUUACAGUUUGAUGGUAUCCAUGUGGUGAGUGGAUCUCUUGAUACAUCAAUCCGUGUUUGGGAUGUGGAGACAGGGAAUUGCAUUCACACGUUAACAGGGCACCAGUCGUUAACAAGUGGAAUGGAACUCAAAGACAAUAUUCUUGUCUCUGGGAAUGCAGAUUCUACAGUUAAAAUCUGGGAUAUCAAAACAGGACAGUGUUUACAAACAUUGCAAGGUCCCAACAAGCAUCAGAGUGCUGUGACCUGUUUACAGUUCAACAAGAACUUUGUAAUUACCAGCUCAGAUGAUGGAACUGUAAAACUAUGGGACUUGAAAACGGGUGAAUUUAUUCGAAACCUAGUCACAUUGGAGAGUGGGGGGAGUGGGGGAGUUGUGUGGCGGAUCAGAGCCUCAAACACAAAGCUGGUGUGUGCAGUUGGGAGUCGGAAUGGGACUGAAGAAACCAAGCUGCUGGUGCUGGACUUUGAUGUGGACAUGAAGUGAAGAGCAGAAAAGAUGAAUUUGUCCAAUUGUGUAGACGAUAUACUCCCUGCCCUUCCCCCUGCAAAAAGAAAAAAAGAAAAGAAAAAGAAAAAAAUCCCUUGUUCUCAGUGGUGCAGGAUGUUGGCUUGGGGCAACAGAUUGAAAAGACCUACAGACUAAGAAGGAAAAGAAGAAGAGAUGACAAACCAUAACUGACAAGAGAGGCGUCUGCUGUCUCAUCACAUAAAAGGCUUCACUUUUGACUGAGGGCAGCUUUGCAAAAUGAGACUUUCUAAAUCAAACCAGGUGCAAUUAUUUCUUUAUUUUCUUCUCCAGUGGUCAUUGGGCAGUGUUAAUGCUGAAACAUCAUUACAGAUUCUGCUAGCCUGUUCUUUUACCACUGACAGCUAGACACCUAGAAAGGAACUGCAAUAAUAUCAAAACAAGUACUGGUUGACUUUCUAAUUAGAGAGCAUCUGCAACAAAAAGUCAUUUUUCUGGAGUGGAAAAGCUUAAAAAAAUUACUGUGAAUUGUUUUUGUACAGUUAUCAUGAAAAGCUUUUUUUUUUUUUUUUUUGCCAACCAUUGCCAAUGUCAAUCAAUCACAGUAUUAGCCUCUGUUAAUCUAUUUACUGUUGCUUCCAUAUACAUUCUUCAAUGCAUAUGUUGCUCAAAGGUGGCAAGUUGUCCUGGGUUCUGUGAGUCCUGAGAUGGAUUUAAUUCUUGAUGCUGGUGCUAGAAGUAGGUCUUCAAAUAUGGGAUUGUUGUCCCAACCCUGUACUGUACUCCCAGUGGCCAAACUUAUUUAUGCUGCUAAAUGAAAGAAAGAAAAAAGCAAAUUAUUUUUUUUUAUUUUUUUUCUGCUGUGACGUUUUAGUCCCAGACUGAAUUCCAAAUUUGCUCUAGUUUGGUUAUGGAAAAAAGACUUUUUGCCACUGAAACUUGAGCCAUCUGUGCCUCUAAGAGGCUGAGAAUGGAAGAGUUUCAGAUAAUAAAGAGUGAAGUUUGCCUGCAAGUAAAGAAUUGAGAGUGUGUGCAAAGCUUAUUUUCUUUUAUCUGGGCAAAAAUUAAAACACAUUCCUUGGAACAGAGCUAUUACUUGCCUGUUCUGUGGAGAAACUUUUCUUUUUGAGGGCUGUGGUGAAUGGAUGAACGUACAUCGUAAAACUGACAAAAUAUUUUAAAAAUAUAUAAAACACAAAAUUAAAAUAAAGUUGCUGGUCAGUCUUAGUGUUUUACAGUAUUUGGGAAAACAACUGUUACAGUUUUAUUGCUCUGAGUAACUGACAAAGCAGAAACUAUUCAGUUUUUGUAGUAAAGGCGUCACAUGCAAACAAACAAAAUGAAUGAAACAGUCAAAUGGUUUGCCUCAUUCUCCAAGAGCCACAACUCAAGCUGAACUGUGAAAGUGGUUUAACACUGUAUCCUAGGCGAUCUUUUUUCCUCCUUCUGUUUAUUUUUUUGUUUGUUUUAUUUAUAGUCUGAUUUAAAACAAUCAGAUUCAAGUUGGUUAAUUUUAGUUAUGUAACAACCUGACAUGAUGGAGGAAAACAACCUUUAAAGGGAUUGUGUCUAUGGUUUGAUUCACUUAGAAAUUUUAUUUUCUUAUAACUUAAGUGCAAUAAAAUGUGUUUUUUCAUGUUAGUAUGCCUGUUUCUUCCACUGAAGUAAUAAUCCUUCAUUAUAAGUAUUUAGGAUUUGUCUAUAAUAUUUAAAUAAGCAAAAUCUUGGUUUCUUUGCAUCCUGCUGUGUGACAUAGAAAUCAAUACUUCAAGCCUGUUUUAUACCGCGAAAGUAAGGAUAAUGUGCUGCAACUGCAAAUUUUAUUUCUCUCCUAGACUAUGAAGGAGGACACUCCACUGUGCUCAUCUCUGUAGAUUGCAUUGGGGUGUAUAAAUAUGAAAUCUGGUUCCCUCAAAGAAUCCACAAAACUUUUGUGAUAAUUACAACUAGAAGCCUUAUAAAUAACAAAUUCAUUUUGAAAUUUUGACCACAUAUUAAGUGCUUACCCUCGAUACUUUCUGUUCAUUCUCUCUUAAGCUCCCACUAUCCCUGAGAAGUAGGCACUAUUAUCUCCCAUCUUAAAGACGAGCAAAAAUCUGCAGCUGAGACUGGUUAGGCAAUUUGUCAAAUCAUAGAACUAGCGGAAUGCCAGAACUCAAACCCAUAUUUCCAAAGACUAAAUACAUGCUGCUCUUUAAGAAAGUUUGACAGACUAAAGCAAGGUUUGAGAGGGAAAUAAGCCAUUUUUCUGGUACUUUCUGACUGUUCUGUAGCCGUUUUGUUCAACAAAUCUAAAUUUUAUAAAAUCUAAAUUUUAUGAUGUAAGGGGAAAAAAUAAAGUUGUUUUUGAAACUA